AGACAGAGUCUCAGGCUGGAGUGCAAUGGCAUAAUCUUGUCUCACUGUAAGCUCCGCCUCCCGGGUUCAUGCCAUUCUCCUGCCUCAGCCUCCUGAGUAGCUGGGACUACAGGUGCCCGCCACCAUGCCUGGCUAAUUUUUUGUAUUUUUAGUAGAGACGGGGUUUCACCAUGUUAGCCAGGUUGGUCUCGAUCUCCUGACCUCGUGAUCCACCCAUCUUGGCCUCCCAAAGUGUUGGGAUUACAGGCGUGAGGCACUGCGCCGGGCCUAGCAUAACAAACUCUUAUUAGCUAUCACCCAGCUUCUAGUAGUAUCAAUACAUUACAAAAUUUGUUCAUUUAUAGCUUCCCACCUGCUAUCCCUUGCUGGUUACUUUAAAAAAUACUUUUAUGUAUACUUUUAAUUUACAUACCAUUAAUGAUUCAUCAAUCUUAAGUAUGUAAUUAAAUGAUUUUUAGCAAACAUACAAAGUUAUGCCAUAAUCAGCACAAUUCAGUUUUAGAACAUUGCCAUUAUUCCAGUUCAUCUCCUGUGGCUGUUUGAAGUCAGUCUCUACUUUUAUCCUGAGCCCAAAGUAACCAUCAGCUUUAUGUCUCUCUAAAAUUGCCUCUUCUGGACGUAUCAUACAAAUGUAAUCAUAUGGUAUGUCUCCUUUCUUGUCUGUCUUCUUUCGCUUAGCAGAUAUUUUUGAGGUUCUUACAUGUUUUACUAUGCAUCAUUAAUUUAUUCCUUUUUAUUGGUGAGUAGUGUUUCUUGGCACAGAUAUAUAACAUUUUGUUUAUCCAUUCACCAACUGGUGAACAUUAGAUUGCUUCCCAUUUUCCCAUGUUUCAAAUUUGGUUAUUAGGUAUAAUGCUGCCUAAUAACCAUAUUAGUCUUUAUUUAGACAUGUUUUCAUAUUUCUUGGGUAUGUACUAAGAGUAGAAUUUUCACAUCAUUUGGUGAUUUUAUGUUUAACAUUUUUUUGUUUGUUUUUGAGAUGGGUUCUCACUCUGUUGCCCAGGCUGGAAUAAAGUGGUAUGAUCAUGGCUCACUGCAGCCUCGACCUCCCGGGGGCUCAGGUGAUUCUCCUAUGUCAGACUCCCAAGUAGCUGGGACUACAGGUGUGCACCACCAUGCCUGGCUAAUUUUUGUGUUUUUAGUAGAGAUGAGGUUUUGCCACGUUGCCCAGGCUGGUCUCGAACUCCUGGACUCAAGCGAUCCGACUGCGUUGGCCUCCCAUUGUGAUGGGAUUACAGGCGUGAGCCACCAUGCCUGGCCCCCGUGUUUAAUGAUUUUUUCUUUGUUGAUUUUUUUUUUUCUUUUGAGACAGUCUUGUCAGUGGUAUGAUCUUGGCUCACUGCAAACUCUGCCCCCUGGGUUCAAGAAAUUCUCAUGCGUCAGUCUCCUGAGUAGCUGGGAUUACAGGCACGCACCACCACUCCCAGCUAAUUUUUGUAUUUUUAGUAGAGAUGGGUUUUGCUAUGUUGGUCAGGCUGGUCUCGAACUCCUGACCUCAAGUGAUCCGUCCUCCUUGGCCUCCCACCAUGUUUAACUUUUUAACAAAUGAUCAAACUGUUUUCCAAAUUGACUGUAUCAUUUUGCAUUUCUGCUUUGCAUUGUGUUUGCAUUCUCGUUUUGCAAUGCAUGAAGGUUCUAGUUCUAGUAAUGUCCUAGCAAAUACCUGUCAUUGUCUGUUGUUUCUGAUAAUAACAAUUGUAGUGGCUAUAAUCAAUCAUUAUGAAUGGUGCCACUGUGAACAUUCUUAUAUGUAUCUUUUGGUGACUAUAUGAAUGUGUUCUAUUGGGUAUUUACCUAAGGAAUGGAAUUGUUGUGUCAUAGGUUAUGUGUUGUUCAGCUUUAGGAAAUAUCAUGAAAUGGUUUUCUCAGGUGAUUAUUGCAAUUUACAAUCCUGUGAGCAGUGAAUGAGAGUUGUUAUUGCUUUAAAUCCUCACCUAUACUUGGUUUUGUCUGUGGUUUUCAUUUUAGCCUUUCUGGUGAAUAUAUGAUGGUAAAGAAUUGUGGGUUUGAUUUGCACUUUCCUGAUGAUUAAUGAAUUAGAGGAACUUUUCAUAUCUUGAUUGGGCAUCUAAAUAUUUUGUGUUAUUAAGUGCCUGUUAAAGUCUCUUGUUGGCUUUUCUCUUAUUGAUUUAUGGUCUUUCUUUCCCUGCCUCCCUCCCUCCCCACUGUCUGUCCGUCCAUCCUUGGGACAGGGUCUCACUCUGUCGCCUAGGCUGGAGUGCAGUGGCGUGAUCCUAGUUCACUACAGCCUCGAACUCCUGAGCUCAAGUGAUCCUCCUACCUCAGCCUCCCAAAGUGCUGGGAUUACAGGCAUGAGCCACUGUGCCUGGCCAGUUUUACUAUCUCUUUAUACGUUCCAAAUUUGACUCCUUUGUCAGAUGUAUGUAUUACAGAUAUCUCUGUAAUCUCAUGUGGAAAUGUUUUGUUUGAUAGCUUUUUAUCUGUUAAUGGUUUCUUUUGAUGAAAACAAGUUUUUAAUUUUAAGGAAAUAUAUUUUUUUUCUUUUAUAUUCAGUGCUCUCUUUAUGUCCUACUUAAGGGUAUAUUGCUAUCCUAAAGUCCACCUUGAGGUGUGUUAUGCAAUGUUCUGGAAUUUUUAUUGUUUAAUAUUUCACAUUUAGUUCUAUGGUCUUUCUGAAGUAAAUUUUCGUAUGUGAUAUUGUAUUGGGGUGAGGAUUUCAUUUUCUAUGUGGAUAUUCAGUUGAAGCAUAUUUUAUGCUUGCACAUAUGCUUGCACAUAUUUUAUACUUGCACACAUAAGUCCUUGCACAUACAGAGUUUUAUUCUAUGAUAUUAUGUAGUCUUGCAAGCAUAUUUUGUGCUUCCUCAACUGAAAAUCCAUAUAGAAAAGUUUAUUUUUCUAUAUGGAUUGAAAAGUUUAUUCCCCCUGACUGCACUCCAGCACUGUAUUGAAGUGAUAUUUUGUGGCACAUUAGUUAACUGUGUAUGUAAGUCUGUUUCUGGACUUUUUAUUCUAGUCAACUGACCUAUCUUUGAAAUAUUUUUUUCCCGAUAUCACACUGUUUUAAGUACUUUGUCUUUAUAACAAUAAAUCUUGAUAUCUGUUCGUUUAAGAUCUUAUACUAUUAUUGCCCUUUAUAUUUUCUUAUAAAUUUUAGAAUCAGUUUGUUAAUUUCUCCCAUAUGCUGCCUGAUAUUUUGAUUGGACUUGGUUUGAAUCUUUAAGUCAAUUUAGGGGGAACUGAUAUCUUAACAAGUCUUCUAGGUACUGUGAUUACAGCAAUGCUCAAAAAAGAAAAAAAAAUCCUUGCACAUGUACAGUUUUUAUUAUUUGAUUUUAUGUGGUCUUCCAGUUAAAUAUAUUAACUUCUUUCUCUUCAAAGCCACUUAUAUGGCAUUAUGGCCAACUGGAAAAGAAUGACUUUUAUAGAAAAAGAAUAAUUUUAUAGAAUUAUUACGAGGAAUGUAUAUUGUUAUCCUCUGUGCAAAGGAUUGAUUGACUAAAAAGAUUGAGCGUUUGUGAGGUUUACAGAGCAUACAGGUGAGCCAUCCUAAAAGAAAAAUAUUGUGAAGGAAAUUAAUUCAAGUGGGAUUGAUCGUAUGACAGCAAUUUGGAAAAUUUUAUCUCAAGCACAUGCAAAGUAAACUUGUAUUACCUCUUUAGGGCGAUGUUAGAAGAAAGAAAGAAAAUAAUAUUGCAAAACCUUGCUUAUAUAAUUGGAGGAAUUCAAGCAGUGAACUUUUUCAAGUUGCUUGGUAGUUUCAGUUUCCUACAAGAGUAUUAAUGUUUUAUUUUUAAGUAUGGUUUGUGAAGUUCACUUUGUAAUUCUCCAGAAGUAACAGAUGUAUUGCAUAUCUGUUUCUACAAAUGACAAAUGUAUCUGUGAAAACAGAAGUCAUGUAAGAAUAACUGAGCAACAUUAAAUAUUAGGGAACAAUCAAGUCUAGCUUCUGACUGCAAUUAGCUAACCACUGAGGUGUUGGUAAAAUCAUUUGCAGUACUCAAACUGAAAUUGCUACAGGCAAGUGCUGUGUAUUAAAGUACUUCCUGUAGUCUUUGGCAGAAUGCUGCUAGUGAAGGAAGGAUACAGAAGGUUACUGUGGCUGGAGAGAAGGAGCAGGAAAACAUUGUGGACUUUAAGGGCGGCUCCUUGCUUAAAGACAAACACAGAGUAAACACAGACAUGUUGGCAAAUACCCUGUGGUAUUUAUACUGUUGCACCUAAAAUUUUUUGCUAUUUUUACUCUUUUAAGAAAUAAAAUUAUGAAGACUUGGGCAUACUAUACAAGAAGUUAGUGUUAUGUGCAUGUGGUGGGGGUUCUUUUUUGGUGAAUUUCAUCUGCAUAGAAACUUAAAAAUGUAGCUUAAUUUAGCGGUGUGUGGUUACUUUUCUGUCUAAUGCUAUUAGAGAUUAAUGGUGAAUAUAUUUGGAGCUUUUCUUUCUGCCAAUCUUGUCCUAUAGAACAAAUAAGGAGACAGGAUAACUAUCACAAUAGGACGUCCACCAGGGCAAAAUUGAGUAUUAUUUUCUGUGUCCUGUUUUGUAAAUUACUUUUUAAAAUCUUACUGUUUAUUUUUAUUUCAUUUUUCCUUAUCUUAUAACAGUGUUUAGAAAUUCAUAUAGAAGGAAGAGCAGAUGGAGUCCUCUCCUGAAAUAGUUGGUACAGUUUGAUUUUUAAGUUUUUAAAAACUUCAUUAAAGGAAGUUUUAAAAAACUUCAUUAAAAAUUUAAUUAAGUUUUUAAACUUCAUUAAAGAAAUGGUGGCUAUAAUUAAAUGUUAGUACUCUUGGGGACAUAGAUUUGCUAGUAAGUUUCACUUUUUCAUGGCUAUUCGGUAGCACAUCUCGUAAAGGUGUUGAGAGGAAAUCAUUGUUGAUGCUGAUCCCCAUUAUUUUCCUCCCCAAACCUUCUGUUUCUAUUAAUUAAUUUAGUGGUUAGGCCAGGAUAAAACAGAGUGGAGAGAGGGGAGAAUUCAUACUAGAUCUGUGAUUUUGAACCUUUUGUGUGUGAACAUGCCCGUUUUUAUUUUGGCUCCUUUUAUACAGGACAUAGUGGUCUGCGUAUGUCUUCACUCAUUUGUUGUUUACCUGGUCCCACUGGUUGAGUUUGAGUCCCCUGCCCUGACCGCUGAUCAAAAAAUAAGAUUUUUUAUAGGCACCUCUGUCUUAACCUCUCUAUAUCAGUUUAUGCUGUGGACUCUUUCUCUGUAUUUUGGGUUAAAGAACAUAUAUUAAGAUCAUGUGUCAGGCACUGUUCUAAGCACUUUACAUAGAUUAACUCAUUUAUGUUUUCCCUAUAACCUUUGAGGGAUACAGUAGUUACUGUUAUUCCCAUUUUAUAAUUGUGGACACCAAGACAAGAAACCUGUGUUUCACUCUGUCCAUUUCCCUCCCUUCAAAUAAUCUACUACUGGACACUUUUUUUUGUCUUUUUGUUGAGAUGGAGUCUCAUUCUGUCGCCAGGCUGGAGUGCAGUGACAUGAUCUCGGCUCACUGCAGCCUCUGCCUCUCAGGUUCAAGCGAUUCUCCUGCCUCAGCCCCCCGAGUAGUUGGGACUACGGGCACACACCACCAUGCCCAGCUAAUUUUUUUUUUUUUUUUGUAUUUUUAGUAGAAACAGGGUUUCACCAUGUUGGCCAGGAUGGUCUCAAUCUCCUGACCUCGUGAUCUGCCCGCCUCGACCUCUCAAGGUGCUGGGAUUACAGGCGUGAGCCACUGCGCCCAGUCCUGGACACAUUUUAAGAGAGACAUUGGCAGUCUGAGGUGCAUCCAAAAGAUGACCAAAGUUGGUGGUGGGGUUGGAAAUCAUGCUUUUUGGGAAAAUGGUCAAAGAAGCUGCAUUAUUUUCAACAGCCUCCAUUAUAGAUUUCAUGUGUAUGCACGUGAAUUGAAUUUGACUAGUUUUUGUAACUCUGAAGUGCAAAACUAGGAAGAGGGAGUAGAGAGAUCAGGAUGACAGAAGGUAUUAGCUAGUUAGAGCAGCUCCAGAAUGGAAGAGACUGUGUCUUCCAAAAGUGUUCUUGUAAAAUAAUUGGUAGACCAUCUUUUAGUAAUAUUGUAGGAGGCAUUUAUGGAAAACAUUUUUCUCCUUAAAAGAUUUUGUUUAAUGUUUCCAAUUGCUUGUGGAAUUGGACAAAUAAAACAUGUGUAAAGGCCCUUCCCAUCUGAAGGAUGCCAGUUUGCAACUUCUGCUUUAAUUGUUCUAGGUUUUACUUCUGAAUCAAACUAAAUUCUUAGUUUUCAGACCACAUUAUUUCACUUCCAGCAGACUGCUUUUACUGAGGUAUGCUUAAACCUCACUUAACUAACCACUGAGGUGUUGGUUAGUUAUUAAGUGAAUGGUGACGCUCUAAGGUCACCAUUCACUUAAUAACUUGUUCAAUUUCUUUUUUUUUUUUAAUUUGACAUUUAGGCCGGGUAUGGUGGCUCACGCCUGUAAUACCAGCACUUUGGGAGGCCAAGGUGGGCAGAUCACUUGAGGCCAGGAGUUCGAGACCAGCCUGGCCAGCAUGGUGAAACCCCAUCUCUACUAAAAAUACAAAAAAAUUAGCCAGACAUGGUGGCAGGCGCCUGUAAUACCAGCUACUCAGGAGGCUGAGGCAGGAGAAUCGCUUGAACCCGGGAGGUGGAGGUUGCAGUGAGCCAAGGUCGUGCCACUGCACUCCAGCCUGGGCGACAGAACGAGACUGUAUCUCAAAAAUAAAAAUAAAAAUAAAAAACCCUGACAUUUAUCAAGUAUCUACUUUACGACUGGCGUGAUGCUAGGUUCUAGGGAUGUCAAGAGAAGGUUGGGAUAUAUAGGCUGUUUAGUGCUGGAAUGUUAUCAGUAAAACAGAGUGGUAUGAGAUGAAGCUGAGGAGCAGACAGGGCCUAUGCCAUAUAAGAGGCUUGUUAGAAAUAGCCUUAUGAAAUAGACUACACUUAUAGGGAUAUUGUUCUGGAGAUUGCUUUCCAUGUCAUUAAUAGACCAUUAUAUGAAGGCUAGGAACAUCUUUGUUUACCCUAUAUUUUCUUCUUGGGACAAUGAAAUUCUUGUUACUGAUAAGUUUCCUUUUUUACUUUUGCCAGAAGUUCUUGUGACUGAUAAGUUUCCCUUUUUACUUUCGCCACCUGGAAAUUCAGUUGAAAAUUCAAGCCCAUGUAUGUGCAUUCUAACUUUCUACCUGGUCUUGAUCUAUUACUUCAUGUAAUUUUCUGUGACUCUGUUUUUUUACAUAUUUAGUUAUUGUUUUAUAUAUAAUCUGAUAAGUGAUUUAGAUUCUUUGUGGAAUGAGACCAAUGUAUCAUUUAUGAAUCUAGAUGUUUUAUUUGCCUUGCUGGUACCCAGAGUCAUUUGUUAUUUGUUAACCUGGGUCUCUUGCUUUUCUUCAAUUCUGGAAAGAAUUUAGUCAUUUCUGUAAAUAUUGCUUCUUCAACAUUAUUUGUAUCUAUCUCUUUUUAAAGUUUUAAUUGUUGUAUCUUGGAUCCUCUUAAUCUAUUUUCCAUGUCUCUUGGUUUUUUCACAUAUUUUUAAUUCUUUGCUCUUUGUGCUAUGUUCUGGAUGAAUUAACCAGUUUGAACUUCCAACUCACCAAUUGUCUAUUUAACUGUGUCUAUUUGAGGGUUUUAUCUUAUCCAUUGCUUUGUUAGUGAUCAUAUUCUUUCUAGGAUUUUUGGUUCUUUUUAGAGAUGUGUGUAUAUAUGUAUGUAUGUAUAUAUGUUCUUAUACCAGUUUUUUUUCAGUUCUGUGUGUUUUUGUAAUUUCUUAUUCUUUUAAAAUUAGAAAUGAUUUUUAAAUUUCUCUUUGGAUAGUUAUUUUGUAGUCUUUUUUUUUUUUUUUUUUUUUUGAGACAGAGUUUUGCUCUGUCACCCAGGCUGGAGUGCAGUGGUGUGAUCUCUGCUCACAGCAACCUCUGCCUCCAUGGUUCAAGUGAUUUUCCUGCCUCAGCCUCCCGAGUGGCUGGGACUACAGGUGCAUGCCACCACGCCUGGCUAAUUUUUGUACUUUUAGUAGAGAUGGGGUUUCACCAUUUUGGCCAGACUGGUCUCAAACUCCUGACCUCAGGUGAUUAGCCCACCUUGGCUUCCUAAAGUUCUGGGAUUACAGGCAUGAGCCACCAUUCCUGGCCUUUUUUUUUGUUUUUUGGAGAUGGUUUUGCUCUGUCAUCAGGCUAGAGUGCAGUGGCGAAGUCAUGACUCACUGCAGCCUCGACCUUCUUUACUUAAGCCAUCCUCCUACCUCAGCCUCCCAAGUAGCUGGGACUACAGGCACAUGCCACCACACCUGGCUGAUUUUUUUGUUUUUUUAAUUUUUUUUUCUUUUUCUUUUUUUUUUUUUUUUUUUACUUUUUGUAGAGAUGAGGUCUCACUAUGUUGCCCAGGCUGGUUUUGAACUCCUGGGCUCAAGCAGUCCUCUUGCCUCGGCCUCCCAAAGUGUUGGGAUUACAGACAUGAGCCAGUGCACCUGGCCUGAAGUCUUUAUAAAGAGUUUUAUGUAUAAUUAACUUCAUCUGUACCAAAUGUGUGUUCCAAUUGUUAAUUUUGUUAACUGUAUAAAAACUGAUAAAACUUUAAACCAAAAAUAUAUAAAGGAAUCUAAUUUUAGUUCACCUUGUGUUUUCAUAAUAACUUUUUUUUUCUCAACUUUUUUUUAACUUCAGGAGUAUAUAUGCAAGAUGUGCAGGUUUGUUACAUAGGUAAAUUUUGUGUGCCAUGGUGGUUUACUGUACAGAUCAUCCAGGUAUUAAGCUCAGCAUCCAUUAGUUAUUCUUCCUGAUGCUCUCUCUCCGCCCCCCCAACCCCACCCUACCCCACCCUCCCUCCACCACCCACCGCACAGGUGUUCAGUGUGUGUUGUUCCCCCACCAUGUGUUCUCAUUGAUCAGCUCCCACUCACAAGCGAGAACAUGCACAUAAUGGCAUAUUUUUAAAGAAGAAAUUAUUUCUUCAUUUAUUUGGGGUACUGAUAUGGUUUGCCUGUGCCCCCACCCAAAUCUCAUCUUGAAUUGUAGUUCCCAUAAUUCCCAUGUGUUGUGCGAGGGACCUGGUGGGAGUUAACUGAAUCAUGGGGGCAGUUUCUUCCAUACUGUUCUCGUGGUAGUGAAUAAGUCUCACGAGAUCUGAUGGUUUUAUAAGGGGAAACCCCUUUCACUUGGUUCUUAUUCUCUCGUGUCUGUCACCAUGUAAGACAUGGCUUUAGCCUUCUGCCAUGAUUGUGAGGCCUCCCAAGCCACAUGGAACUAUCAGUCCAUUAAUCCUCUUUUUCUUUAUAAAUUACCCAGUCUUGAGUAUGUCUUUAUCAGCAGUGUGAAAAUGGACUAAUGCAGGUACCUCAUAAAGGUCCUUGUAAGACUGUUCUCAAUGAUUUCAUGUGAAAUGAUUUUGUAUUUCAAUUGCUGGAAUAUUGGUUUAAAGCCUCAUUUUGAGAGGUAGGGGUUUUUGUUUUUUUUCAUUCCGCUCAUUUUCUCUGUGCUUAUCCUUCUCUGUCUGAUGAUUUUGCACUUGUUCCUUUUCAGCUCCUAAGUCUUUAAUGUAGAACCAGGUCUUAUAAAUGCUUCAGGGAUCUUGAACAUGAUGAUAUUGGGGAUAUGGCAGACCUACCACUGAACCAGAGGGGAAGUUCAAAUUGUUUUUUAUUCAAUUUAAGAGCAUAUCUAUUUUCUUUCUUUCUUUUUUUUUUAUUAUACUUUAAGUUCUGGGAUACAUGUGCAGAACGCGCAGUUUUGUUACAUAGGUGUAAUGUGCCAUGGUGGUUUGUUGCACCCAACAACCCGUCACCUAUGUUAGGUAUUUCUCCUAAUGUUAUCCACCCUCUAGCCCCCAACCCCCAACAGGCCCUGGUGUGUGAUAUUCCCCUCCCUAUGUCCAUGAGUUCUCAUUGUUCAACUCCCACUUAUGAGUGAGAACAUGCAGUGUUUCGUUUUCUGUUGUGAUAGUUUGCUGAGAAUGAUGGUUUCCAGCUUCAUCCAUGUCCCUGCAAAGGACAUGAACUCAUCCUUUUUUAUGGCUGCAUGGUAUUCCAUGGUGUAUAUGUGCCACAUUUUCUUUAUCCAGUCUAUAAUUGAUAGACAUUUGGGUUGGUUCCAAGUCUUUGCUAUUGUGAAUAGUGCCGGAAUAAACAUACGUGUGCAUGUGUCUUUAUAGUAGAAUGAUUUAUAAUCCUUUGGGUAUAUACCUGGUAAAGGGGAUCUCUGGGUCAAAUGAUAUUUCUGGUUCUGGAUCCUUGAGGAAUCGCUACACUGUCUUCCACAAUGGUUGAAGUAAUUUACACUCCCACCAACAGUGUAAGAGCGUUCCUAUUUCUCCACAUCCUCUCCAGCAUCUGUUGUUUCCUGACUUUUUAAUGAUCGCCAUUCUAACUGGCGUGAGAUAAUAUCUCAUUGUGGUUUUGAUUUGCAUUUCUUUAAUGACCAAUGAUGAUGAGCAUUUUUUCAUGUCUGUUGGCUACAUAAAUGUCUUCUUUUGAGAACUGUCUGUUCAUAUCCUUUGCCUACUUUUUGAUGGUUUUUUUUUUCUUGUAAAUUUGUUUAAGUUCUUUGUAGAUUCUGGAUAUUAGCCCUUUGUCAGAUAGAUUGCAAAAAUUUUCUCCCAUUCUGUAGGUUGCCUGUUCACUCUGAUGAUAGUUUCUUUUGCUGUGCAAAAGCUCUUUAGUUUAAUUAGAUCCCAUUAGUUUUGGCUUUUGUUGCCAUUGCUUUUGGUGUUUUAGACAUGAAGUCUUUGCCCAUGCCUAUGUCCUGAAUGGUAUUGCCUAGGUUUUCUUCUAGGAUUUUUAUGGUCCUAGGUCUUAUGUUUAAGUCUUUGAUCCAUCUCGAGCUGAUUUUUGUAUAAGGUGUAAGGAAGGGAUCCGGUUUCAAUUUUCUGCAUAUGGCUAGCCAGUUUUCCCAACAACAUUUAUUAAAUAGGUAAUCUUUUCCCCAUUGCUUGUUUGUGUCAGGUUUGUCAAAGAUCAGUUGGUUGUAGGUGUGUGGUGUUAUUUCUGAGGCUUCUGUUCUGUUCCAUUGGUCUAUGUAUCUGUUUUGGUACCAGUACCAUGCUGUUUUGGUUACUGUAGCCCUAGUUUGAAGUCAGGUAGCGUGAUGCCUCCAGCUUUGUUCUUCUUGCCCAGGAUUGUUUUGGCAAUGCAGGCUCUUUUUUGGUUCCAUAUGAACUUUAAAGUAGUUUUUUUCCAAUUCUGUGAAGAAAGUCAGUGGUAGCUUGAUGGGGAUAGCAUUGAAUCUAUAAAUUACUUUGGGUGGUAUGGCCAUUUUCAUGAUAUUGAUUCUUCCUAGCCGUAAGCAUGGAAUAUUUUUCCAUUUGUUUGUGUCCUCUCUUAUUUCCUUGAGCAGUGGUUUGUAGUGCUCCUUGAAGAGGUCCUUCACAUCCCUUGUAAGUUGGAUUCCUAGGUAUUUUAUUAUCUUUGUAGCGAUUGUGAAUGGGAGUUCACUCAUGAUUUUUCUCUGUCUGUUAUUGAUGUAUAGGAAUGCUUAUGAUUUUUGCACAUUGAUUUUUUGGAUCCUGAGACUUUGCUGAAGUUGCUUAUCAGCUUAAGGAGAUUUUGGACUGAGACGAUGGGGUUUUCUAAAUAUGCAAUCAUGUCAUCUGCAAACAGAGACAAUUUGACUUCCUCUCUUCCUAUUUGAAUACCUUUUAUUUCUUUCUCUUUCUUGAUUGCUCUGGCCAGAACUUCCAAUACUAUGUUGAAUAGGAGGGAUGAGAGAGGGCAUCCUUGUCUUGUGCCGGUUUUCAAAGGGAAUGUUUCCAGUUUUUGCCCAUUCAGUAUGAUAUUGGCUGUGGGUUUGUCAUAAAUAGCUCUUAUUAUUUUGAGAUACAUUCCAUUGAUACCCAGUUUAUUGAGAGUUUUUAGCAUGAAGCGCUGUUUAAUUUUGUCAAAGGCCUUUUCUGCAUCUAUUGAGAUAAUCGUGUUUUUUUGUGAUUGAUUCUGUUUACGUGAUAGAUUACAUUUAUCGAUUUGCAUAUGUUGAUCCAGCCUUACAUCCCAGGUAUGAAGCUGAUUUGAUCAUGGUGGAUAAGCUUUUUGAUGUGCUGCUGGAUUUGGUUUGCCAGUGUUUUAUUGAGGAUUUUCGCAUUGAUGUUCCUCAGGGAUAUUGGCCUUAAAUUUUCUUUUUUUGUUGUGUCUCUGUCAGGCUUUGGUAUCAGGAUGAUGCUGGCCUCAUGAAAGGAGUUAGGGAGGAUUCCCUCUUUUUCUAUUGUUUGGAAUAGUUUCAGAAGGAAUGGUACCAACUCCCCUUUGUACCUCUGGUAGAAUUUGGCUGUGAAUCGGUCUGGUCCUGGACUUUUUUUAGUUGGUAGGCUAUUAAUUACUGCCUCAAUUUCAGAACUUGUUAUUGGUUUAUUCAAGGAUUCGACUUCUUUCUGGUUUAGACUUCGGAGGGUGUAUGUGUCAAGGAAUUUAUCCAUUUCUUCUAGAUUUUCUAGUUUAUUUGCAUGCAGGUGCUUAAAGUAUUCUCUGGUGGUAGUUUGUAUUUCUAUGGGAUCAGUGGUGAUAUAAGAAUAUCCCACAGGAUAUCACCACUGAUAUAAGGAUAUCACCACUGAUCCCACAGAAUCAGUGAUAUCCCUUAUAUCAUUUUUUAUUGCGUCUGUUUGAUUCUUCUCUCUUUUCUUCUUUAUUAGUCUGGCAAGCAGUCUAUUUUGUUGAUCUUCUCAAAAAAACUGCUCCUGGAUUCAUUGAUUUUUUUUUUUGAAGGGUUUUUCUUGUUUCUAUCUCCUUCAGUUCUGCUCUGAUCUUAGUUAUUUCUUGUCUUCUGCUAGAUUUUGAAUUUGUUUGCUGUUGCUUCUCUAGUUCUUCUAAUUUUGAUGUUAGGGUAUCAAUUUUAGAUCUUUCCUGCUUUCUUUUGUGGGCAUUUAGUGCUAUAAAUUUCCCUCUACAGACUACUUUAAAUGUGUCCCAGAGAUUCUGGCACGUUGUGUCUUUGUUCUCAUUGGUUUCAAAGAACAUCUUUAUUUCUGUCUUCAUUUCAUUAUAUACCCGGUAGUCAUUUAGGAACAGGUUGUUCAAUUUCCAUGUAGUUGUGUGGUUUUGAGUGAGUGUCUUAAUCCUGAGUUCUAGUUUGAUUGCACUGUGGCCUGAGAGACUGUUAUGAUUUCCAUUCUUUUGCAUUUGCUGAGGAGUGUUUUACUUUCAAUUAUGUGGUCAAUUUUAGAAUAAGUGUGAUGUGGUGCUAAGAAGAGUGUAUAUUCUGUUGUUUUGGGGUGGAGAGUUCUGUAGGUGCCUAUUAGGUCUGCUUGGCCCAGAGCUGAGUUUAGGUCCUGAAUAUCCUUGUUAAUUUUCUGUCUCAUUAAUCUGUUUAAUAUUGACAGUGGGGUGUUAAAGUCUCCCAUUAUUAUUGUGUGGGAGUCUAAGUCUCUUUGUAAGUCUCUAAGAACUUGCUUUAUGAAUCUGGAUGCUCCUGUAUUGGGUGCAUGUAUAUUUAGGAUAGUUAGCUCUUCUUGCUGCAUUGAUCACUUUACCAAUAUGUAAUACCGUUCUUUGUCUCUUUCAAUCUUUGUUGGUUUAAAGUCUGUUUUAUCAGAGAUUAGGAUUGCAACUCCUGCUUUUUUUUUGCUUUCCAUUUGCUUGGUAAAUAUUCCUCCAUCCCUUUAUUUUGAACCUAUGUGUGUCUUUGCACAUGAGAUGGGUCUCCUGAAUACAGCACACUGAUGGGUCUUGACUCUUUAUCCAAUUUGCCAGUCUGUGUCUUUUAAUUGGGGCAUUUAGCCCAUUUACAUUUAAGGUUAAUAUUGUUAUGUGUGAAUUUGAUCCUGUCAUUAUGAUGCUAGCUGGUUGUUUUGACCAUUAGUUGAUGCAGUUUCUUCAUAGUGUUGAUGUUCUUUACAAUUUGGCAUGUUUUUGCAGUGGCUGGUACCGGUUGUUCCUUUCCAUGUUUAGUGCUUCCUUCAGGAGCCCUUCAAAGGCAGGCCUGGUGGUGACAAAAUCCCUCAGCAUUUGCUUGUCUGUAAAGGAUUUUAUUUCUCCUUUGCUUAUGAAGCUUAGUUAGGCUGGAUAUGAAAUUCUGGGUUGAAAAUUCUUUUCUUUAAGAAUGUUGACUAUUGGCCCCCACUCUCUUCUGGCUUGUAGGGUUUCUGCCGAGACAUCCACUGUUAGUCUGAUGGGCUUCCCUUUGUGGGUAACCUGACCUUUCUCUCUGGCUACCCUUAACAUUUUUUCCUUCAUUUCAGCCUUGGUGAAUCUGACGAUUAUGUGUCUUAGGGUUGCUCUUCUUGAGGAGUAUCUUUGUGGUGUUCUAUGUAUUUCCUGAAUUUGAAUAUUGGCCUGUCUUGCUAGGUUGGGGAAGUUCUCCUGGAUAAUACGCUGAAGUGUGUUUUCCAACUGGGUUCCAUUCUCCUUGUCCCUUUCAGAUACACCAAUCAGAUGUAGAUUUGGUCUUUUCACAUAGUCUCAUAUUUCUUGGAAGCUUUGUUCGUCCUUUUUAUUCUUUUUUCUGUAAUCUUGUCUUCUUUCUUUAUUUCAUUAAGUUUAUCUUCAAUCACUGGUAUCCUUUCUUCCUCUUGAUCGAUUUGGCUAUUGAAACGGUGUAUGCUUCAUGAAGUUCUCGUGCUGUGUAUUUCAGCUCCAUCGGGUCAUUUAUGUUCUCCUCUACACUGGUUAUUCUAGUUAGCAAUUCGUCUAACGUUUUUUCAAGGUUCUUAGCUUCCUUGCAUUGGGUUAGAACAUGCUCCUUUAGCUUGGAGGUGUUGGUUAUUACCCACCUUCUGAAGCCUAUUUCUGUCAAUUUGUCAAACUCGUUCUCCAUCCAGUUUUGUUCCCUUGCUGGUGAGGAAUUGUGAUCCUUUGGAGGAGAAGAGGCAUUUUGGCUUUUGGAAUUUUCAGCCUUUUUGCACUGCUUUCUCCCCAUCUUUGUGGAUUUGUGUACCUUUGGUCUUUGAUGUUGGUGACCUUCCAUUGGUGUGUUUGAGUGCACAUGCUAUUCCUUUCUGUUUGUUAGUUUUCCUUCUGACAGGCCCCUCUGCUGCAGGUCUGCUGAAGUUUGCUGGAGGUCCACUCCUGACCCUGUUUGCCUGGGUAUCAUCAGCAGAGGCUGCAGAACAUCAAAGAUUGCUGCCGAUCUUUCCUCUGAAAGCUUCGUCCCAGACAGGCACCUGCCAGAUGCCAGUCAGAGCUCUCCUGUAUGAGGUGUCUGUUGGCCCCUACUGGGAGGUGUCUCCCAGUCAGGAGGAACAGGGGUCAGGGACCCACUUGAGGAGGCAGUCUGACCCUUCACAGAGCUCGAACACAGUGCUGGGAGGUCCACUACUCUCUUCAGAGCCACCAGGCAGGGAUGUUUAAGUCUGCUGAAGCUGUGCCCACAGCUGCCCCUUUCCCCAAGUGCUCUGUCCCAGGGAGAUGGGGGUUUUAUCUGUAAGCCCCUGACUGGGGCUGCUGCCUUUUUUUCAGAGAUACCCUGUCCAGAGAAGGGAAAUCUGGCAGUCUGGCCACAGCAGCCUUGCUGAGCUGCAGUGGGCUCCACCCAGUUCGAACUUCCCAGAGGCUUUGUUUAUACUGUGAGCAUAAAACCACCCUACUCAAGCCUCAGCAAUGGCGGACGUCUCUCCCCACACCAAGCUCGAGCGUCCCAGGUCGAUCUCAGACUGCUGCUGUGCUGGCAGUGAGAAUUUCAAGCCAGUGGAUCUUAGUUUGCUGGGCUCCGUGGGGGUGGGACCCGCAGACCCAUACCACUUGGCUCCCUGGCUUCAGCACCCCUUUCCAGGGGAAGUGAAUCGUUCUGUCUCACUGGUAUUCCCGGUGCCACUGGGGUAUGGAAAAAAAGAAUUCCUGCAGCUAGUUUGGUGUUUGCCCAAAUGGCCACCCAGGUUUGUACUUGAAACCCAGGGCUCUGGUGGGGUAGGCACUGGAGGGAAUCUCCUGGUCUGCAGUUUGCGAAAACCAUGCGACAAGCACAGUAUCUGUUCCAGAGUUCUUCAGGCUCAGUCCCUCAUGGCUUCCCCUGGGUAGGGGGAAACAUUCCCUGACCCUUUGUGCUUCCCAGGUGAGGUGACCCCCCACCCUGCUUCGGCUCGCCUUCCAUGGGCUGCACCCACUGUCCAACCAGUCCCAAUGAGAUGAACCAGGUACCUCAGUUGGACAUGCAGAAAUCAUCUGCCUUCUGCGAGGAUCUUGCUGGGAGCUGCAGACCAGAGCUGUUCCUAUUUGGCCAUCUUGCCAGCAAUCCUUGCCUGUUUUCUUUUGCUUCUAUUUAUCAACAGUUCUAUAUAAGUUCUUGUUCCUGGCAGCUGUUGGUAGCAUUUUUUCAGCCUUCCUUCAUGAACACGGGAAUCUCACUAUAGUGCCUGGUUUCAAGCUAUGAACCUGGCUCCUGAUCCCUGUCCCACUGUGAGCCCUUUUAGUUUCCUUUACUUUGCAGGAGCCAAACUCUCCAUUGCCUUCUUCUUAACCUAGAGUUUUGUGUAUUUCUAACUUCAAUCUUGCCCACAGCUUUGCUUUUCUGGCCCAGGGGAAAUAGUUAUCUUAUUUUCAUGCCCAUUUUUGUCUUAUAGUUUUUUCCUUUUUAUUUUUUAAAUCUCUCAUUCAUAAGUGUUUUCAGUGGGAUGAGUGGACAAUCCAUCAAAGCAUGAAAUAAUUACAUGGUCUUCAUGCAAAGUCUUUCUUAGAUAGCCUUUAUGGCUCCUUCUGGCUCUGACAUUGUAUGAUAUACUAUUGAUUAUUUCCCCUGGAAAACUUUCUCACUGUAAUGUGUUCCUUCAUUGCCUGUGAGAAGGAGCACAAGACAAAUAAAACUUUUUUUUUAUCCUGGUAUUUUUCCAGGCUCCUGGUAUUAGAAUGUUUGAAAUGAAAUUAUACAAAAUGUCUUCAGAUAAAUUAUGAGUUCUUGGGAAAUUAUGUUUGAAUUUGCUGGUGACAGAUAAUAAUAAUAAAUAGGUAGAAAUGAAGAUAUGAAUAAUGCUUCAAUUUCCUAAAUGCCAAAAUAUGGUACAAUUAGACAUUUGUUUAAACUUCCUUGAAUGGGUGUUACUUUCCUGAGGUUUAACUUUAAAUUAGUGGCUGCAUUUGCAUUCAUUCAAUGAAUCUAUUGGGUGACUAACUCCUUAUACAGUAACAGAGUCACAGAGGUUAAGGCUAGGCUUCUAGAGGUGUUAGUCAUCUCUGAUAGCAGUGUAUCCUACCUGCUUUUAAAAAGAACAUUUUAGUAAGGAUAGGAGGUAUACGUUAGAGGAAUAUAUAAUUUGCUUUGUUUGUAACAGGAAUACCUGAGAAUGUACUGAUGACCAUGUAAACAAGGUACAGUUUAGGGUAGAAUUUCUGCAGAUAUAAGCAAAGUUUUGGUACAACAAAUGGUUAAUUUAUCAAGUCUUCUAUUAGUCAAGGAUUGUUUGAGAGUAUGCUAAAACUGUUGUCUGUUCCUUAACCGUGGGUUUUCAUUGUCUUGGGAUGAGAAUCCAUGCUUUCAGAUUGCCAGAAUUCUGGAAGUGUUCACAGCUAGGGGAAAAAAAGAAAAAAAAAGAAAGAAAACCUCACAGAAAAUUUUUAGUAAAAUUCAUUAUUAGCCGGUUUCUCAGGACUUCAUUUGGUACCAGGAUACAUAAAACUUGAAUUUUCAUAGACUAAUUUUGCUUUUCCUCUUACCAUGGAAAGAAGAUUAGAAGUAUUGGUUGACCUUCAGCAAAAUAAACUUAGUACAAGGCAGAAGAAGUUAGAGUGAAGGGUAGGGAGCAUUCCUCGUUUUUAGGGAUAGUCACAUCUGACAUUUAUGUUUAUGAUUUAUGAACUCUUUGAAGUGCAGUCUGAUGGCUAACACUUAUCUGACACAAUGUUUUCUUUAGCCCGUCCUACAACUUCUUAAUCCUAGAAAACCUAGAAAUUAAUUUUUAAAAUUCCUUUUUUAAAAAGGAAACAACUUUAUAGUGUAAAAAUCCUUUUCUGGUAUGGGGGUUAAAAAAAAAACCCACGGAGGGUAAAUAAACCGUAGUUCACACAGUGUAAUGUAAAGUCUUCAGCCAUUGUCAAUAGACUCUGUAUUUUGAAAUCAUUUUGCUUUCAUCCCAAAUGGUUGACUUUUCAGUAUUUGAGCUAGACUUACCUUAUGAAUUAUAGUGUGCAUUCUCACUGAAAGUAGUCUCAUUUUCUUGUUUACAUUUAUAUCCAUGUUUGUUGAAUUGAGUACAGUUCAACAAUGGUAUUUCUUAGCUUAGCUUAAAAACUAAAAUGGGAUGAUUCAUUGAGUCUAUUUCACCUUAUGUUAUAGAGGCUAGCCUAUCAAUGUAAGGACUGUGGAAACUCAUAUGCAAUUAUAUUUCUGGUUGGUAAGUGAUCCAAAAAAGAUGUAAAAGAUUAUUUAUCCCGUUAGAAAAUGAAAGUCUAGGUGGGAUGGCUCACACGUGUAAUCCCAGCACUUUGGGAUGCUGAGGCAGGCGGAUCACCUGAGGUCAGAAGUUCAAGACCAGCCUGGCCAACAUGGUAAAACCCCAUCUCGACUAAAAAUUCAAAAAUUAGCCAGGUACUCGGGAGGCUGAGGCAGGAGAAUUGCUUGAACCUGGGAGGCAGAGGUUGCAGUGAGCUGAGAUCACACCACUGAACUCCAGCCUGGGCGACAGAGCAAGACUCUGUCUUAAAAAAAAAAAAAAAAGGAAAAUGAAAUAAACCUAAAAAACAAGUAAUCAUUAUCAGAGAAUGAUUAUAUAGCCAAGAAGUUUUGUUAAAAAUAAAGAUCUUGAAGCCUUUCCCUAAUUUAACUAUGUAUCUUUCUAUCAUGUGUUAUACUAGUAGUAUUCAAAUCAAGAAGUUAGUCAGUUUGUUGUUUAGAUAAUUGAUGGGCAAAUUGUGAUGACAUCUAGCCAUACCAUGUCACACUGAGUAUGUUACAACUGGAAUUGUCCUUUGUUGUUAGAAUAUUGGUAUAUAUACUAUACCAUUUAAUGUCUGAUUUUCAUAGCUCUCUGUGCUGUAAUAACCUCAAGUGUUAAUGCCAGGUUGCUGUAGCAUCAGCCUGGCUGAUUUUAUGACAUAAAACAAUAAUGGUCCAAUACCUUUAAAGAAUACAGAAUUGGCCAGGCACAGUGGCUCACGCCUGUAAUCCCAGCACUUUGGGAGGCUGAGGCAGGCGGAGCACGAGGUCAGGAGAUCGAGACCAUCCUGGCUAACACGGUGAAACCCUGUCUCUACUAAAAAUACAAAAAAUUAGCCAGGCGUGGUCGUGGGCGCCUGUAGUCCCAGCUACUCGGGAAGCUGAGGCAGGAGGAUGGCGUGAACCCGGGAGGCGGAGCUUGCAGUGAGCCAAGAUCGUGCCACUGCACUCCAGCCUGGGCGACAGAGCGAGACUCUGUCUCAAAAAAAAAAAAAAAAAGAAUACCGAAUUGGCAGUCCUGGAGGCUUAUGUGUCCCAGGCUCCUCUUAGAUCCCUCAAGAACUGAGGGGAACUCAUUCCCUGUAUAGCUGUGGGGCGCAAUACAUUGUUUGGGAAGCUCUGAUUUAAAGGGUUAGGGACUGAGCUUGAUUAAUAGAUGUACAGAACACUUUGAGAAUAAGGGUUUUGUUGAUGAUGAAUAAACUGGGAGUCUUGGCAUAUCUCGUGGUGACUGAUGUUGAAAGGGAAAUGGAGCCUAAUGGAAUAGUCCUGAUGGCCACCUAGAAGGAGGUAGAAUAUUCCUUAUAUAGAUGUUUUCUCCUCCCUCCCUCCCUUCCUCUCUUCUUCCCUUCUGUCCUUUCCAUUCACCUAUAUCCUUUUUAAUAUAGUUUUCUGGAGAAGGCCUACCUCUGUUGGCUGUGAGGGCAGGAAGCAGACAAGUAAGCUGGGAACCCCCAUAAUUACCACAGUAAGGAAAUCCUGGUGGAAUGCUUUAAGUUUCUCUUCUGAAGGAGAUUACCUGGCUGUUUUUUUUCUUCCUUGUGAUUCUUUAGCUUCUGUUUUGCUUCUCCUAGUGGCCUCAGUGCCCAUGCUUCGAACCUGUGUACUGUGUCCUAGGUACUAUGCCGGUCACUUAAAGACAUGAUUUCAUUUAAUCUUUAAUUGUGGGGUAUUCAUUUGUUUACUACAAAGGUCCUUCUGCAUUUUCCUAGGUUGUUUCCUUAUGUACUUCACGAUGCAAAUCAAUUGUCAACCUAUGGAUUUUAUUUAUUUAUUUUAUUUUAUUUUUUAGUUUUUGAGUCGGAGUCUUGCUCUGUCGCCCAGGCUAGAGUGCAGUGGUGUGAUCUCGGCUCACUGCAAGCUCCGCCUCCUGGGUUCACGCCAUUCUCCUGCCUCAGUUUCCCAAGUAGCUGGGACUACAGGCGCCUGCCACCAUGCCCGGCUAAUUUUUUUGUAUUUUUAGUAGAGAUGGGGUUUCACUGUGUUAGCCAGGAUGGUCUCAAUCUCCUGACCCUGUGAUCCACCCACCUUGGCCUCCCAAAGUGCUGGGAUUACAGGCGUGAGCCACCGCGCCCGGCCUUGUCAAUCUAUGGAUUUUAUUCCCUCAUCUGUUGCUGCUCAGUCUGAAUUUGAUGGCUCUCAUGUGCUCUCCUGUAGUACCUUUUGUUUCUGUCAUAUGACUUAUUGUUCUGUUAUGCUCUCUUCUCUACCUAUUUUGCAUAGUCUCUGGUAUGUGUUAAAUGCAUGGUGAAUGUUUAUUUAAUGAAUGAAUGAAUGAGGAAAUAUAGUUUCAAGUUCUGAGAAUGAUAAUAAAUCCUUAGGUGAAAUUUACCCCAUUUGAAAGAUUAAAUUGAUUCAUUUUAGCAAAGUUGAAGAGACAAAUGUACCUAAACAGUCCUUUUUCAUUGUGAACAUGUAUGACUUUUAGAAUCUAGGGAGACAAAAAAUAAUUUUUAAAAAGAUUACAUUUUGGGGGUAUGAGCAGUGUUCUUUACUAAUACCGGUAUUCCCUAGCAGUAAAAAAUAACUCCUGUACAUCAAUUAGCAAUUUGUUUGCAUCAAAGAGAUUUUAAAGAUGGAGACCAUCUCUUUACUUUAGGCACAGUUGCACAGGACCCCUACCUUGGCUCGUAAGCCCAGAAACUCAAUUUCAGUUUACCCAGAAGACAUGUCCUGAUAAAACUAACAAGACGCUUAACCUAUUAAUGUAUAAUGGACAUCUGCUGGUCCAGAUAAGUAAGACACUUAGGGAAGCAAGGUUGUAGGUCAAAGAUAGUAAGCAUUUAAUUUGAACUGAGAGAAUGAGUUUAGUUUUUUUUAUGGGGUGGGGCUUGUGAUCAGAUUUUUUUUAUUGUGGUAAAAUAUACAUAACAUAAAAUUUAUCAUUUUAACUAUUUUUAAGGGUAAAAUUCAUUGGCAUUCACAGUGUUGUGCAACUAUCACCACUAUUUCCAGAACAUUUUCAUCAACCCAAAUAGAUAUUCUGUAAUCAUUAAGCAGUAAUUCCCCUUUGUCUCCUCCCACAGCCCCUGAAUCUACUUUCUGUUUCUAUAAAUUUGCCUAGUCUAGAUACUUCAUAUAAAUGGAAUCACGAUGUUUGUCCUUUUGGACUUCAGUAUUCUUAAAGGAUAUUUCUGCUUUUCUACUCUACAGAUUGUCUGUUUAAAUAAUGGUUUUCAAAUAUCUUUUGAUGGUAUGUUUUAUCUAUUAAAAAAUUUAAGUGAUAUAUAUAUUUGUAACAUACAUGUACUCUGUACUAAUAUAUUGUAUACAUUAUAAAAUAUGCAUAAAAUCUUAAUGAAAUAAAUAUUAUUUUGAAAUAUCAGUAUCUUUUGAUGACUUUCUGCUAUCAUUAGCUUGUAUCUCAAGGUUUAAAACUUUGUCUUAUUUCUUAUCAGAUUUUAUUGGAUGGUCAUUGUAUACUUCUCCUGAUAAAGAGCUCUGUAUGGGUAGAAAGUGGCAGCUCUGCCAUUUGUUUGUAUUUGAAUUAUUAGUAUUUACUUCAGUGUUUCUUUAUCAGAAUUUUUUUUUUUUUUCGAGACAGGGUCUCACUCUGUUGCCCAGGCUGGAGUCCAGUGGGGUGAUCAUGGCUAAUACGGUUUGGCUGUGUCCCCACCCAAAUCUCAUCUUGAAUUGUAGCUCCCAUAAUCCCCACACAUGUUGUAGGAGGCACCCUGUGGGAGGUAAUUGAAUCAUGGGGGUGGUUUUCCCCCUGUUGUUCUCAUGAUAGUGAGUUCUUUCGAGAUCUGAUGGUUUUUAUAAGUGCCUGGCAUUUUCCCUCCUGGCACUCAUUCUCUUGCCUACCGCCAGGUAGGAUGAGCCUUUGUUCCUCCUUUUGCCUUCCCCCAUGAUUUUGAGGCCUCCCCAGCCACGUGGAACCACAGUCCAUUAAACCUCUUUUUAUAAACUACCCAGUCUCAAGUAUGUCUUUAUUUAGCAGCGUGAGAAUGGACUAAUACAACAGCCCACUGGAGCUUCAACCUCUUGGUCUCAAGCAGUCCUCCCACCUCUGCCUCCCCAGUAGCUGAGAUUACAGGCACAUGCCACCAGGCCCACAUGUCUGUAGUCCUAGCUACUCUAGAGGCCGAGGUGGGGGGGAUCACUUAAGACCAGGAGGUCAAGGCUGCAGUGAGCCAUGAUUGUGCCACUGCACUUCAGCCUGGGUGACAAAGCCAAGACUCUGUCUGAAAAAAAAAAUUAUAACAGGAAAAGGUCCUUUCUCUCUUUCCUCCACCCCCUCUGUUUGUUUCCCCCACCUCCAUCCCUCCCUCCCCUCCUGUAGUUGGAAUACUUGUUAUGUGUCUGGGAUUCUUUAGGGUCUUCCAGAUUUAGUGCUUCUUCCCCUAUCUGGAUCAGACUAUACUUCGAUUCUUUUUAAAUCCAAAAUAGACAGGAAUUUUAGGAUACCAAGAGACAGAGACUACAUUGAAGGGUUUACAUGCCCAUCAUUCCCUAUCACAGGAAAUACCUAAAUGGUAUUUAAAUUUCUUUUUUUUUUCUAGCCCCCUGUCUGCGUGUUGGAAUGUUUAAUCGUUUUAAGGGUCUGGGCAGUCCUGUCUUUGCUUACUGAAUGAUUGGGAAGGAAAAUAGAGAAGUAAUUCCAGUGGGUUAUGUUCAACCAUCCAGAGCAGAGAUUGGCAAACUUUUUUUUUUUUUUCUGCAAAGGACCAGAUAGUAAAUAUUUUAUGCUUUGAGGGCCAUAUGGUCUCUGUCAAAUUUCCCAACAUUGCUGUUGUAGAGUGUAAGCAGCCAUAGACAAUUGGCAAACAAAUGGAUGUGACUGUCUUCCAGUCAAACUUUAUUUAGUGAAACAGACAGCAGGCUAGAAUUUGCCAACCUGUGCACUCAAACUAUCUGUUGUGAGGACUCUUCCCCCCUUUUCCCUUAAAAUUUGUAGAUGGACAUUUUUGUAAAAUACAAUAAAAGUGAAUUAUUGGAUGAGUAAAAAAUACAUGGUUAAAAUUUUUAGAUUACAGACAACAAGUUACAUUUCAAUCUAUAAUUUAAAUGGUCAUACAUAGGGAAAAAGAAAACAAUUAGAAGAACCAUAAAUGUUGUUACUUGAAGAUAUCUUCUAUUAAUAUAGAGAAUCGCUGCUAUAGUCAUAACUUUUUUGUCAUUCUGUAAUACUAACUAAACACAAAGCCAAGCAAAAUUGCAGCUCUCCAUUUAUUAAAUGCCCAUACUGUAAACAAACAUUGUAUAUAUGGAUAUUUAACAAUUUUAAUAUGACAUAGAUUUGCUUUUUGCUAUUAGUUUAUCUAAUCUAGGUUGGAUUGACGACAGUACUACUCACAAGAGAUAACGUAUUUGUAUACUACUCCUAUAUUUUGUUUUAACAACACUCAGUUUAGAGAAACCAGAUUUAAAAAUAUGUUGCUGUGAACUGAAGACAUUUAGAUUUAAAAGAAAUUUUAGCAAGCUCAGGAUAUUCAUGUCUAACUUUUUUCCAAGGUGAAGCAAGUGAUUUUUUUCAGAAUUCAUUUUCUAUCUUUCAUUAGUAGUCAAUUCCAAUAAUUUAUCCUGUGGAAUUACAGUUAAAUUUAAAUUAUCUCUCAAUGAAUAGGUUGUAGAUCCACACAUUUCUUUUGUAUGAAUCUUCUUUUGGUGGAAAAAAUUUGAAAAUGUUUUUAUCAAAUUUGUAAGGUUAGUGAUAAUUUUUCAACAAAUAUACCAUACCUGAUUAUACCUACUUCAUUGAAAAUUAUGGACCAAAAAAAAAAAAAAAAAAAAAGGCUGGGUGCAGUGGCUCACUCCUGUAAUCCCAGCACUUUGGGAGGCUGAGGUGGGCAGAUCACUUGAGGCCAGGAGUUUGAGACUAGUCUGGCCAACAUGGUGAAACCCCAUCUUACUAAAAAUACAAAAAUUAGCUAGGUGUGGUGGCGGGCAUCUGUAAUCCCAGCUACUUGGGAGGCUGAGGCAGGAGAAUCACCUGAACCUAGGAGGCGGUGGUUGCAGUGAGCUGACACCACACCACUGCUCUCCAGUCUGGGCAACAGAGUGAGACUCCAUCUCAAAAAGAAAAAAAGAGAAAAUUAUGGAAUAUGUCCUAAAUAUCUGUAGAAACUGAUCUUUUCAUGCUAUUAGCAUCUUUUUUUGCCCUUUGAUCUUAUUGGUCAUUGAGAAAUACUUGUAUCCCUUUCUUACAAGUAUGAAGAUUAUUAAAAAUACCGAAUAUAUAAGAUGAAUAAAUCCAAUUGUCCAAUUCACACCUUUAAAACAUUAGGACCAAACUUUUUUAUCUUGCAGAAACACUAAGAAUUUGUUUCAUUGUUUAUUUUCGACAGUGUUUCUCCUUGACAACCAUGGAACUUCAGUAUGUAGUAACAGUAGUGUACAAUUAGUUUUCAUAUCCUCUCUCAGUGAAGAGAGUACUCUCUAAUACACUGCAUUAGCCUUUAAGUAAUUCACAAUUACACUAUUAAUUGUCACUAAACGUACUGUUUAGACAGGUGUCUUUUUUUAAAAAAAAAAUUAUACCAAGAGUUUCUCAAUGAUGGAAACAAUGCAUUGAUUUACACUCUGGAGUAAACGGCUUAAUCUGGAUAACUGCUCCAGAAUACUUUCUUGUCAUUACAAUUGCACCAUCAGAAUAUACCGUUACACAAAAUUUAAACUCAAAUCAUGUUUAUUGACUUAUAAUUUUUCAUAGAUUUGUACAGUUUAGAAAUCGUUAUGUUUGGCAGUGAAGCAGAAAAAUAAUUCUUCCUUCACAGCACCAUCAUGUUCAGAUCACAUAUAUACCAAAGGAAAUGCCAUACUAUCUUUGCAUUUAUUAAGUUUCAAUUAAAAACAUGUCACUAAAUUUCUUUGUUCUGUGAAUUGGUCUUCCAUGUCAUUAACCAGUUCCUGAAUUCAUCAGACUAUGGUGUCAUUGGAAAUUGGUUCUUUAUUGCAGAUUCACUGAAUAUUUCCAAGCAAACAUCUUUGGUGGAAUUUUUCCCUGAUGUCAGUGUGUGUGGGGUGUGUGUGUGUGUGUGUGUGUGUGUGUGUGUGUGUGUGUGUGUGUGUUUAUAUACCGUGUUAGCAUCCUGAAGGUCUAUUAUAUAAAAAGCCUGAAAACACUAAUACUUAUUUGAAAUAGCAGACAUUUGCUUCUGUUGGCUUUGCAAUUCACUACUAUUUAUUUCAAAUUUUUUUUGUUGUUUUGAAUGUCUAUAUGGUUUUUGCAUAAAUACUACUUAGGUUUUGAGGGUUUUAUUGUUGCAUAGCCAGUACAUCUCUGCAGAUAACCCAUAGUGGUUUUAAACUUUGCUGUCAGUCAUACUUUUGUGUAAAAUAGUAUAAAGUCGUUGGUCUUUAUUUCUUUGAAAUUACUUUCAUUGUUGUUUGGUUUACUACCUCUGCCUCAUUCAGAGACAUUUUAUCUUUUUUUGCCAAGGAAAGCCCAUUAAACUUUUUCUGUUUGUAAAUUAGGUGUAAAAAUACCUAUUUACUUCCUUAAUUUAGCUAAAAAUAUUAAAUUAUAAAUUAUAGGCUGAUUAAAAUUUAAAUGACACAAUGACAGAUUAUGAAAAUAUGCUUACAUUUUCUCAGAUUUAAAUUUUUUAUUUUUUUAUUUUUUAGAGCUAGAGUCUUACUCUGUCACCCAAUCUGAAGUGCAAUAAUGCAAUCUUGGCUCACCGUAGCCUCAAUCCCCUGGGUUCAACUGAUUUUCCCUCCUCAGCAUGCAACACCACUGGCAGCACCAUGUGUGACACCACGUCCUGCUAAUUUUUAAAGUUUGGUAGAGACAGGGUCUCACUUUGUUAGCCCAGACUAGUCUUGAACUCUUGGAUUCAAGCGAUCCUCCCACCUUGGCCUCCCAAAAUGUUGGGAUUACAGGCAUGAGCCACUGUGCCCAGCAAGAUUUUUAAAAUAUUUCCAUUAUAGAUAACAAACUAACUGAUGUCAAAUUGCUUAAAACUUUCUAAAUGCUUACUCUCAAUUUCUGUACUUGCCUGUUAUGUAUCAGUAACAAACAGUUGGAGGACCUUUGUUCUAAUCUAGAGACUAAUAGAAGGCCAUUGUAGCAAGAAGGGGUGUUCUGAGUCUUAUAUUAUUUUUCUUAGAGUAGAUAUUCUCGGCCUUUGGUAAAACUUAAUUAUAGUUUUCAUUUGCUGUAUUUGAGAUUCAGUGAGACGGUUUUUUCCUCAUGUUAGUGAAUGGAGACAUAACGUUCAACCAAUAUAAAGGGACUUUAAGCAGGCAAUUUGCAGAUGUUCCCAUUAUCUCCCCAUGUGGAUAUGGAAAGGCUUGUUUAAGGACAGCAGUCUUAGUUUAUGUCUUAUUUGUUCACCUGUUACUGAAAAACCAUUGUGGGGGCCUGGGUUCCUAUGUCUAUUUUCUGAUUACUCCAAUGUUGUCCCACGAAAGGAACUAUUUAAGAGCCUUAUAUAUUCAGCAGCUAUAGCUCAAAUCCAUUGUGAUAAAGGUGACCCGUCCCAUAUAUGUUUAUAGUAAUAUUCUUUCUAUAUGGUUUAUAAAUGUACAUAUAUGUCUGCAUAUGAUAUGUCUCUAUAUCAAUCUAAAUACGUCUUUUUCACUUAUUUCUACAUAUUGUUGAAUUGCUUAAUGACUUUUUAUGGAAACUUGGAGCUAGAAGUGGUGUGAAGGUCAUAUGGUCCAGCCCUCUUUUUAAUAUAGAGGCUGGCAAACUAGGGCUGUCUGGUCUGACACCUGUUUUUGUAAGUAAAGUUUUGUUAGACCACGGACAUACCUAUUUGUUUACAUAUUGUCUAUGGCUGCUUUCUCACUACAAUAGUAUAUUAGGGUAGUUGCCCUGGAGAUCUUAUGGCCUGCAGAGCCAAAAAUAUUUACUCUCUGGCCUUUUACAGAAAAGUUUACUGACUUCUUAUAUAGAGAGGCCUGGCAACUUCUACCUGAAUUCAUUCAGUGACAGUAUUUCACUCUCUCUCAAAGCAUUCAGCUUAUAGUUAGUUUCUAUUUAUCUUGAGCAAAACUUUUUUAAGAAACCUUCCUUGUACACAUGAUAGACUUUUAGGAAUUUGAAAACAAUUUUUUUUUUAUGGUCCUUUUGUGCUUUUAAUAACCAUAAUAUUGAUUUCACAAAAUUUUAUCCUCUCCUUAAAAAGUUGGUAAGAACGUACCCUCUAAAAAUGGUAGCCCUUUAAAAUAUGCCUUACAUAGUAUAAAAGAAUUAUCCAACUCUUCAGGUGUCUCUCUUUCCCCCUUUUUCUUUUUUUUUUUUUUUUUAUUAUACUCUAAGUUUUAGGGUACAUGUGCACAUUGUGCAGGUUAGUUACAUAUGUAUACAUGUGCCAUGCUGGUGCGCUGCACCCACUAACGUGUCAUCUAGCAUUAGGUAUAUCUCCCAAUGCUAUCCCUCCCCCCUCCCCCGACCCCACCACAGUCCCCAGAGUGUGAUAAAAACAAUUUUUAUACUUCUUAUCUCUUUCUAGUAGUCUACAUCCCAUUCCCAGUCUUUCCAAUCAUAAAAAUUUGUAGUUUAUUUAGUUCACACUUGAACGUCCUAUGAAACUGUUUUAAACCUUUUACCUAUCUUGUUUCUUGUCAUUAUUCUUAAGCCAUUGAUACAGAAAUCAGAACCAAAUUUAAUAUUGUUGUGGGUAUGAGACAGUUUCUGUCAUGUUUUAAUUUUUUCCUUAAAGUUUUACUAUGUACUUCAUAUAUACUGGGCACUCAACUGUGUUAUUAUUACUUUAAAUAUGUGCUAAGUGGCAUUAUUUUUUAAACAGUGAUAUCACAUUAAAGGUUCUUAAUGAGCUCAAACUCAAAAACCACUACGUCUUUUUACAUAUCUUGCUAUUAAAUCAGAUCUUCACCAUCCUACGCUGAACCCAUGGCAGGACUUUUUACUCCUUUGAGAUUCUAUUGUAUUAGGUUUAUUCCACUGUGUCAGUAUGUUGAGAAGUUUUAGCAUCUUGAUUCUGUUAUUUAAAUAUUUACUGUUCUUCAUAGCUCUUUGUCAUGUGAGAAUUUGAUAGCAAUGAGUUACUCGAUCAACAUCUUGCUAUGUUUGUGUGGUCGUUAUUGAAUCCAAGUGAAAUUGUUCUGGGAAUUUUUCUUAGAGUUUAUGGUAGAUUGAAUUAUUGCUCAGCAAAUAUUCAUUCCCCACCCUUUCUCUUGAGGUGAACUAUACAUACAUCCCUGUCUUACUGAUUUUAGACUUGGUCAUACGGCUUGCUUGGACUAGUAGAAUGGAGAUGGAAUUGACUGUAAAGCCAUUUCUAAAAUGAGGCUUUAAGAGGCAUGGCAAGUUAUUUCCAGCUUUUUCGUACUUCCGGCACUUACUGUAAGAAGAACUUGCCCCAGGUAACUACUUCAGAUGGGGUCCCAGAAUGAAAGAUAUGUGAAGGAUACCUGAACUUGACCCUGCAACCUGAAGCAGAGAUGCUCUAGCCAACCUGCAGAUUCAUGAGCAGAAGUUAGCAUUUAUUGUUUUAAUCCAUUUCCACUUUUUGAGUUGUUACAGAGUAUUGAUUCAGCAAUAGCUGGUCCAUACACAGCUAACCAAGCCAUUCUGUUUUGCAGGAAUUAUCUCUGAAAUGCCUAGUACCUGUAAAUAACAAGCCAGUACUAGACUAUCAUGAACCUUGGCUUAAGGGAGAUCAGAGGUAACUUUUGGGUCCCAUAUGUGUGUCGGUACAUGGCAUGAGCUGAGGGAUGCCGCUGAAGAAAGGAACUACAGUUGGCUAAACAGGAUAUACAGAAAUAUCCUGCUGCUCUAGCUAUGCCUCAAAUGCUUUGGGUCAGAUUUUUACUUUUUGCAGUUUGAUAUGCUAACAUUGUCAAGUUUUUCUAUUACUUUCUGUUCUGUUUUCUUGUUCCUCCUGUAUUUUUUUUUUAACUUCCUGCCUUUUUAGAAAUAACUCAUGUUUUCACAGUAUGUACUACUUAAAGAAACAAUAUAGAAUAAGACCAUUAGAGUUCUAAUUAUGGCUCCACCAUUUGUUAACAUAAUCACUCUACAUAAAUUACUUAAGCCAUUUCCCCCUCUGCAUAUUGGGAUUAAUAAAUAACUCACAGUUGUUGCUAAGCUUAAAUGAGAUAACAAAGUCAUUAGCUCACCAUCAUUUGUAUAUACAGUCAUUAGCAAAUAUUUACUGAGUAAAUUCUGAGGGAUACAGUGCUUUGCACAUUAUAAAAAAGUCAAUACAUUUUAUAGCAUUUUGAUAGUCCUAGACCUAGAAAGUACUUGUUGGGGUCACAUUGAUGCCAAAUGAAAGGAAAAGAGAAGGGGGUUCUAAUCCCAUUUCUGAAAGAAAGAGCAUAAAUAUUUGCCGUUAGAAAUCAUGGAACAGUUUUUAGAUGUGUUUUAUGUUAUUUGAUAGGUUAAUACUUUAUUUCAGGAUUUCUUUUUGCAUUAUCCUUGGCAGUGGCUAGGUACUGUCAAUGACCAGUAUUUUUUGUUCUAUCUGGGGAUGUGAAUCCAAAACAAAGGAUAGAAUUGCUUGUGCUCUGUUUUUCUCUCAGUUAAUUUUUUCAAAAUAUAAUCCCAAGUACAAAUCAUGCUUUUGAGUAUUAUAGGGGAUCAUAUUUUUUUCUUAUAACCUUGAAUAAGAUGCAGUAAAAACAGUGAAGCUGACCACUUUUCUUCCCUAUCAUUUAGGUAUGUAGCUUCUACCAGAUAUUUUGACAUCCUGUUUCAUAAGAAUCUUUUUCUUUAAUUAAAAAAAAAAUGGUAGUUUUAACAAUUCAAAUAAUAUGGGUGGUACAUGAAAUAUUUGCCUUUUUUUUUCAAAUUUACAGUCAUGUUUGGUAUAAAUCUUUUCCUUUUAUGUGUACUCAUUUAAUAUGUAGUUUUUCCUUUAUAAAAAAGUAGAAUUAUAUUCACAUUUAUUCUGCAUCUUGUCUUUUAUAUUUAAUAGUAUUUUUUAUCAUUGAUAAAAAUAUCAUUGAUAUUUUCCCAAAGUGAAUACAGAAAGACCUCAUUUUAUUGACAGCAUCAUAGUUCGUAUUGUGGAUAUAAAUUAUUUAACAUCCACAUAUUUUGAUCUACAUCCUAUUGAUUUAAGUUGUUUAAAGCAAUACUGUGACUGGGCAUGGUAGCUUACGAUUGUAAUCUCAAGAUUUUGGGAGGCAGAGGUAGGAGGAUCGUUUUUGGCCAGGAGUUCAAGACCAGCCUGGGCAACAUGGUGAAAUCCCUGUCUUAAUCAAUCAAUCAAUAAACAAACAAAUACACAUACUACAAUAAAUGUACUUAUUUAUCUUGUUAUACUUGUGCUUUUAUUUUAGCAGUUCUGAAAAUGGCUUCCUUGUAAGCGAAGUCUAUCUAUAUUUAAAAUUUUAAUAGAUAUUAGUAGGUAAAAACAUUUUUAAAAACUUGAUUACUAAUAAAAAUUUAAAAUGCUACACCAAUUUAUAUUUCUACCAAUAAUUUAUAGUAAUGUGGUGCAUCCUAUCUUACCAGGAGUGGAUGCUGCCAGUCAUUAAAUUUUUGCCAUCCUGGGCCAAAAAUGAUAUCUAAUUUUGUUUCCUUUCUAUGAAAAUUGGUAUUCAGACAUAUUCCAAUGUUUGUAGCUAUUUACAAUGCAUUCUUGCUGUAUUGGCCAUUCAUAUCUUUUUUAUUAUUAAUUGUUUUCUUUUUAAAAUCAGUUCAUAAGGCUUUUCAAAAAUUCUUACAGAGGCUGGGGAUGGUGGCUUGCACCUGUAAUCCCAGUGCUUUGGGAGGCCAAGGUGGGAGAAUUGCUUGAGCACAGGAAUUCGAUUGUAGCCUGGGCAAGAUGGCAAGACCCCUGUCUUUACAAAACAUUAAAAAAUCAGCAUGGCAUCAUGGUGUGUGUCUUUAGUCCCAGCUACUUCAGAGGCUGAGGCCACAGUAUCCCUUGAGUCCAGUAAUUCGAAGUGGCAGUGAGCUAUGAUCCUGCCACUGCACUUCAGCCUAGGUGACAAAAUGAGACCCUGUCUCUAAAAAAAAAAAAAAAAAAAUUACUGAAAUUAUUGUAGAAAUAUAAGCAAGAGAUGUUUUUUGCUUUCCUUCCAUUUUUUUUUCUUUUAUUAUUAUACUUUAAGUUUUAGGGUACAUGUGCACAUUGUGCAGGUUAGUUACAUAUGUAUACAUGUGCCAUGCUGGUGGCUGCACCCACUAACUCAUCAUCUAGCAUUAGGUAUAUCUCCCAAUGCUAUCCCUCCCCGCUCCCCCCACCCCACAACAGUCCCCAGAGUGUGAUGUUCCCCUUCCUGUGUCCAUGUGAUCUCAUUGUUCAGUUCCCACCUAUGAGUGAGAAUAUGCGGUGUUUGGUUUUUUGUUCUUGCGAUAGUUUACUGAGAAUGAUGAUUUCCAAUUUCAUCCAUGUCCCUACAAAGGACAUGAACUCAUCAUUUUUUAUGGCUGCAUAGUAUUCCAUGGUGUAUAUGUGCCACAUUUUCUUAAUCCAUUCUAUCAUUGUUGGACAUCUGGGUUGGUUCCAAGUCUCUGCUAUGGUGAAUAGUGCCACAAUAAACAUACGUGUGCAUGUGUCUUUAUAGCAGCAUGAUUUAUAGUCCUUUGGGUAUAUACCCAGUAAUGGGAUGGCUGGGUCAAAUGGUAUUUCUAGUUCUAGAUCCCUGAGGAAUCGCCACACUGACUUCCACAAUGGUUGAACUAGUUUACAGUCCCACCAACAGUGUAAAAGUGUUCCUAUUUCUCCACAUCCUCUCCAGCACCUGUUGUUUCCUGACUUUUUAAUGAUCGCCAUUCUAACUGGUGUGAGAUGGUAUCUCAUUGUGGUUUUAAUUUGCAUUUCUCUGAUGGCCAGUGAUGAUGAGCAUUUUUUCAUGUGUUUUUUGGCUGCAUAAAUGUCUUCUUUUGAGAAGUGUCUGUUCAUGACCUUUGCCCACUUUUACCCCAUUCUUUUUUUUUUUUUUUGAGAUGGAGUCUUGCUCUGUCGCCCAGGCUGGAGUGCAGUGGAGCGAUCUCGGCUCACUGCAACCUCCGCCUCCCAGGUUCAAGUGAUUCUCUUGCCUCAGCCUGCUGAGUAACCAGGAUUACAGGCACGUGUCACCACACCCGGCUAAUUUUUUGUAUUUUUAGUAGAGAUGGGGUUUCACUGUGUUAGUCAGGAUGGUCUCGAUCUCCUGACCUCGUGAUCCACCUGCCUCGGCCUCCCAAAGUACUGGGAUUACAGGCGUGAGCCACUGUGCCCAGCCCCAUCCUUAGUGUUAGAUGAUUUUUAUAUAACAUGCUAGAAUGUUAAAUUAUUGCAUGUACUAUGUGCACUGUUUUCUAUAUAGUAUUUACCCAGCAUUUGCCUAAUUUUAAUGUUGUAUCUAGCACAUGUAUGCUUAAUCUCUUAAGGACAGAGUUUGAAUUCUAUUAUUGUAGAUUAAUAGAAUUAAGAUUUAUGAGUGACUUUUUUAAGGGACUGGGGUCUCACUCUGUCACCCAGGCUGGAGUGCAAUGGCAUGAUCAUAGCUCGCUGCAGCCUCAAACUCCUGGGCACAAGUGAUCUCACUUCAGCCUCCUGAGUAGCUAGGACUAUAGGUGUGUGCCACCAUGCCCAUCUAAUUUUUAAAUUUUGUGUAGAGAUAGAGGGCCUCACUGUGUUGCCCAGGCUGGUCUCAAACUCCUGGGCUCAAGCGAUACUCCUACCUUGGCUUCCCAAAGCAUUGGGAUUACAGAUAUAAGACACCACACUCAGCCUCUGACUUUGGAAAUAUUCAUAAGUUUUUUUUUAAUUGAGGAAUUCAGCGUUAAUAAGUGAGGCAAUAAUCAUAGAAUUUUACAGUUCAGUUUAAGAGUAAAAUGUAUCUAUUAAAAUGGUCUCUUUGUUUGAUUUAUACAAAGGUGACAUAUAGUAGCAGGCCUUGGAUGUAUCAGUGGUAACAAAUUUGGAAUCCGUUGUAAAUAUAGGAUCUCACUGGUAAAUAUACUGUGUUCAUUUGGAUAGGCUAAUUGUUUAACCAACAACUCCCAAAUCACUGAGGCUUAUAAAAAGAAAUUUAUUUCUCACUCACCUAAUAGUUUGUUGCCAAAAUUGGUGAAUGGCCUUCCAAGGGAUGAUGAUUCAAUGAUCCAGGCUCCUUUAAUCUUGAGGUUCCUAGAUCCUUUAGUCCAGGCUCCUUUGAUCUUGAGAUUUCUAGAUCCUUUAGGGCCUCAAGUCCUCAAUGGAUCCUCUACAUCUAGCUAGCAGAGAGGAAGGAAAAAAAAGAUGGUACGUGGAGGUUAUGGUGGAUCAGAACUGAAUGUAACACAUAUCAUAUCUCUUAAUAUUUCCUUGGCCAAAACUCAGUCACAUAGUCACAUCUAAUUUUAAAGGAGGCUGGAAAAUUUCUUCUAUGUAUAUGCCUUGGAAAAGAGGAGAAUGGGGAUACUGGUAAAGCAAGCUAUCUCUGACAUAUAUUUAAUUUAAAAGUACCAAAAUGGGUUUCUAAAUCUGAAUAUAUUUUAUCUAUACUGUGUACAUUGGGUCAGUUUUUAAAGACAACAAUAAAAGUUGUAUGUAAUUUAACUGAUUAAUUCCUUUAAUUACACAAAUAGUUGGUGGAUCUGCUUACCAAAAUGGAAAAGAACAAUUAAGCAAAUAGAAAAUUUAAAUUAUACAUUACUUGACAGGUUGCCCAGAAAAGUGGAUAGGAUGAUAAAUACUUGCUUAUGGAAACUGAUAAUAUUUAUCUUCACUACUUGACCGAGCCUUUUAGUGAUUUAAUCUGUGAUGAAGAGAAGUAAAAAUUCCUUCAUGAUAAAAUCUCUCAACAGACUGGGCAUAGAAAGAACAUACCUCAGCAAAAUAAAGGCUAUGUAUGACAGACGCACAGCUAACAUCAUACUGAAUAGGGAAAGGCUGAAAGCCUUUCCUUUAAGAAGUGGAGUAAGACAAGGAUGCCCACUUUCACCACUCCUAUUCAGCGUUGUGGCAGAAGUUCUAGCCAGAGCAUCAGUCAAGAGAAAGAAAUUCAAGGCAUCUAAAUAGGAAAAGAGAAAGUCAAAUUGUCCUUCUUUGCAGAUGACAUGACCUCAUAUAUAGAAAAGCCUAAAGAUUCCAACAAAAAACUCUUUGAACUGAAAAAUGAAUUCAGUAGAAUUGCAGGAUACAAAAUCACCAUACAAAAAUCAGUAGCAUUUCUAUAUACCAAUAAUGAACUAGCAGAAAAAGAAAUCAAGAAAGCCUCAAAUUUAUAAUAGCUAGAAAAAAGUAAAAUUCCUAGGAAUAAAUUUAACCAAGGAGAUGAAAGACCUACAACAAAAAACCGCAAAACACUGAUGAAAAAAAUUAAAGAGAACACACAAAAUGGAAAGGUAUCUCAUGCUUAUGGACUGGAAGAAUGAACAUUGUUAACAUGACCAUUCUACCCAAAGCAAUCAACAGAUUCAAUGCAGUCUCUAUCAAGAUACUAGUGACAUUCUUCAUAGAAAUAGAAAAAACAAUUCUAAAAAUUGUAUGGAACCGCAGAAGACCUCAAUAGCCAAAGCAAUCCUGAGCAAAAGGAACAAAGCUGGAAUCGUCACAGUACCUGACUUCAAAAUAUUCUACAAAGCUAUUGUAACCAAAACAGCAUGGUAUUGAUAUAAAUACAGACACAUAGAACAAUGGGAUGGAUUAAGUAACCUAGAAAUAAACUCACAUAUUUUACUGCCAACUGAUUUUUGACAAAGGUGCCAAUAACUUAUAUUGGGGAAAGGAUACCAUCUUUAAUAAAUGCUACUGGGAAAGCUGAAUAUCCAUAUGCGGAAGAAUGACCCCUGUCUUUCACCAGAGUUUAAAAAUAAUCUCAGCCGGGUGCAGUGGCGCAUGCCUGUAGUCCCAACACUGGGAGGCUGAGGUGGGUGGAUCACCUGAAGUCAGGAGUUGAAGACCAGCCUGGCCAACACAGUGAAACCCUGUCUCUACUAAAAAUAAAAAAAUUAGCUGGGUGUGAUGGUGGGCACCUGUAAUCCCAGCUACUUGGGAGGUCAAGGCAGGAGAAUCACUUGAACCCAGGAAGCAGAGGUUGCAGUGAGCUGAGAUCGCGCCACUGCACUCCAACCUGGGUGACGAGUGAGACUCUGUCUCAAAAACAUAAAUAAAUAAUAAUAAUCUCAAAGUGGAUUAGACUUAAACCUAGGACCCAAAACUAUAAAACUACUGACAUAAAACAUAGAGGAAAUACUCCAGGACAUUGGCCUAGGCAAAAAUUUUAUGGCUAAAACCUCACAAACCAAACACAAAACUGUGAACAAACCAAAACACAAAAUUGAAAAAUAGGACUAUAUUAAAUUAAAAAGCUUCUGCACAUCAAAGAAACAGUCAACAUAGUGAAGAGACAACCUGUAGAAUGGGAGAAGGUAUUUGCAAGUAUUCGUUUAAUAAAGGACUAAUAUCCAGAAUAUAUAAGAAACUCAACUCAGUAGCAAACAAACAAACAAAAAAACUCCAUAAAUUAUCCCAUUAACAAGUUGGGAAAGGAUAUGAAUAGACAUUUCUCAAAAAAAGACAUAUACAUGGCCAGUAGGUAUAUGAAAAAAUGCUCAGCAUCACUAAUCAUCAGGGAAAUGAAAAUCAAAACCACAAUGAGAUAUCAUCUUACCUCAGUCAGAAUGGUGAUUAUUAAAAAGAACAACAACAAAAAACUGUUGGCAAGGAUGCAGAUAAAAGGUAACUCUUAUACAUUGUUGGUAGGAAUGUAAAUUAGUAUAGCUACUAUGGAAAACAGUAUGGAAGUUUCUCAAAAAACUAAAAAUAGAACUACCGUAUGAUCCAGCAAUCUCAUUACUGGAUAUUUAUCCAAAGAAAGGAAAUCAGUAUAUCGAAGGGAUAUCUGCACCCCCAAGUUUGUUGCAGCACUAUUCAUAGUAGCCAAGUUAUGGAAUCAACCUACGUGUCCAUCAACAGAUGAAUGGAUAAAGAAAAUAUGGUUUAUAUACACAAUGGAAUACUAUUUAGCCAUAAAAAAGAAUGAAAUUCUGUCAUUUAUAGCAACAUGGAUGGAACUGGAGGUCAUUAUGUUAAGCGAAAUAAGCCAGGCACAGAAAGACAAAUAUCACAUGUUCUCACUCACUGAUAUGUGGGAGCUAAAAAAGUUGCUGUCAUGGAGAUUGAGAGUAGAAUGAUAGUUACCAAAGAGGGGGGGGAGCAGUUUGUGGGAAGGUUGAAGGGAAGAUUGGUUAAUGGGUACAAAUAUACAGUUAAAUAGAAGGAAUACGUUUUAGUAUUUUAUAGCACAGUCGGAUUAGUGUAAUCAACAACAAUAUGUCUUUCAAAAUAAUUAGAAUACAUGAUUUGAAAUAUUUCCAACAUGAAGAAAUGAUAAAUGUUUGAGAUGAUAAAUAUCCUAAAUACCUUGAUUUGAUCAUUACAUAUUGAAUAUGUGUAUCAAAAUAUCAUGUGUGCCCCUUAAAUGUGUACAAUUAUUAUGUAACAAAAAAUUGUAAAACCGAAAGUUUGUUCAUUUCUUUAUAUAUCUUAUUGACAAGGGAAGGUAUCACCAACAGAAUGGACUUGAUAUUGAUAAGAGGUAGAUCUGCUCAACAAGACUUGGGAAGGAGGAUGGAAUAAACUGUAUGGUGUUUGAGAAAUAUACACCAGACACAUACAAAUGUGUAUCUGUGUGUAUGUGUUUAUACAUCUCACAUGUAUUGUAAUAGUGCCCUUAAUGAAAACACUCUGCCUCUGGCAAAAAACAAAAAACAAAACACCCCUCUUUUUGUUUUUCCACAUGACUGCGAAACAAUUACAGCUUCUAGUAGGAGGGCUUCUCCUGUUCCUGGGAAAAGAGCUGGGUUGGUUGGCAUUUGCAUAAUCGUCUUUGGGGCCAUUGUGGGUGGGUUUGGGCUGCUGACACAGAGCUGCAGACUGGCCACCUGUCCAAAACAAAUGAACUCAGCCUUUGUGUAACAUUAUCUGGUUAUCCACAGUGUUAUUUCUGAGUAAUGGAUAAUUUGGUUAAAAUAAUAUGAAACUAUUAUUUAGGAAACAUUGUGUUCAACGUAAGUCCUCCAUUUUGCUGGGAGAAAAAUUUUCUUCUUUUUCCACUGGCACAACUAUGUAUUUCCAUAUCAUCUUUGGUAUAGUUUUAUAACUGCUUUUGUGAUAUCCUCAUGAAUAUUAAUUAGGGAUAUGAAAAUUUAAAAAGAAACUUCAAAAUGAUUUGCAUUCGUUAUUCUAUAAAUUAUAAAUUAAUUGUUGUCUUUUUCUAGCAGUCUGUUUUACUUAUGUGGAAUAAUUAAACACUUAAAGUCAUCAAAAAAGAAGACACAUCUAAGAUCUUGAUGUAAGAACAAGUCCUGCAUCAUUCGUUAUCCUUGAUAAUGAAUCCAGUGACUCACCUGUGAAUUUAGGAAGUUUUUGUCCUAAUAAUGCAUAUAUUGCUGUGUUGAGUAAUUUUAUUAAUCAGCUACAUUUAACCUAUAAUGAAUACAUACUUACACAUUUUUAAAAUUCACCUGUGACAAACUUACAUGUGACAUAUUAAUAUUUCUUUUCUUUCUUUCUUUUUUUUUUUGGAGACGGAGUCUCUCUCUGUUGCCCAGGCUGGAAUGCAUUGGCAUGUCUCGGCUCACUGCUACCUCCAUCUCCCGGGUUCAAGCGAGUCUCUCACCUCUGCCUCUGGAGUAGCUAGGACUACAGGCACGCCCCACCAUGCCCAGCUAAUUUUCGUAUUUUUAGUAGAGAUGGGAUUUCACCAUUUUGUCUAGGCUGGUCUCCAACUCCUGACCUCAAGUGAUCCGCCCACCUCUGCUUCCCAAAGUGCUGGGCUUACAGGUGUGAGCACUGCACCCUGCAGAAAGUUAGGUUCUGUUAUGGAGGUAGGUUUAUGAGGAAUCCUAAAGGAAUUGCUUACUCCCAGUGAGACAGUCUUGAACUAGACUCUUAGGAAUAGAUAGGAUUUGGAAUACACGGAUAUUCCAGUUUGAAACUGGUUGCAGAUAAAAAUAAACAGUGAUUCUGCAAUUAUUAUGGAGACUUAAGUAAUAUUAGAAAGAAGUAAGGAGAUACACUUGGAAGAUACUAAGUUGAUACAACUUGAUAGAAGAUUAUGAAUACUAGGCUGGGGGUCAUUACAGAAGUCAAGCCAAAAAAAUGUACUGGAAAAAGAACACUAAAGUGGGAGGCAUGUCAUAAUUUAUAUGGAUAUUGGCCUUAUUACUUGGUGACAGAUCUUUUUUUUCAACUUUUAUUUUAGAAUCAGGGGAAUACAUGUACAGGUUUGUUACAAAAAUAUAUUGCAUGAUGCCGAGGUUUGGAGUAUGAAUGAAUCUAUCACCCAGGUAGUGAGCAUGCCUAAUUAUUUUUUCAACCCUUGCCCCUGCCUCACUCCCUGCUCUUGGAUUCCCUAGUGUUUAUUAUUCCCAUGUUUAUGUCCAUUUGUAUUCAAUGUUUAGCUCCCACUUAGAUAUGAGAACAUGUGGUAUUUGGUUUUCUGUUUCUGUGUUAGUUUGCUUAGGAUAAUCGUUGCCAGCUACAUUCAUGUUGCUACAAAGGACAAGAUUUCAUUCUUUUCAUGGCUGCAUAGUAUCCACGCUGUAUAUGUACCACAGGUGCCCAUCAGUGGUGAGUGAUCUUGAGUCACUGCCCAUUUUUCUUGAUCUGAGAGGAUUCGACUGGAUAAAUUAUAAGGUCCCUUUAAGAAUCAAUCAGUCAUCAGAAUUUCUUUUCCUUUUUUUUUUUUUUUCUUAAAGAGACAGGGUCUUACUCUGUCACCCAGGCUGGAGUGCAGUGGCACAAUCAUAGCUCACUGCAGCUUCAAACUCCUGGGCUCAAGCGAUCUUCCCAUUUCAGCCUCCUGAGUAGUUGAGACUAGAGGCAUGCACUACCACGCCCAGUUAAUUUUUAAAUUUUUUAAUAGAGACAGAUCUCCUUGUUGCCUAGGCUUGGCUUGAACUCCUGGCCUCAAGCAAUCUUCCCACCUCGUCAUAAGAAUUUUUUAGUGAUAGAUGGUUUUGUUUUUAAUAUUUCAGCUGGAAAACUAUUUUAGCAUCUAGCAGAAGACUUGUUUGUGGAAAAAGCUUGACUUGGUGAAUCUUUUCAUCAGAGUAAUCCCUAUGUUUCACAUAUUUCAUAUAAAAAUAAAAUAAGUUUCCCACUCUUUAGUGUGAAAUUGGUGAGGGAUUGGAUAUAAAAGGUUAUGCUCUGGAUAUCCCAGAGAACUGCCUUCUUCUUUUCCUAAAGUUGUCCACUAUGUUUGAGGUUCUGCUCUAUGCAUAACAAGUGUGAUUGCUUUUGGAGGGUUACAAGGUAAUGAGGACUCCUAUAUUCAGAAUGUAAAACCCAUUUGACAAAGUAAGAUAGGUAUGCAUAAAAGUUACAAAUAUAUACUAUCAAUAGGGCUAUAUCUGACUUAUAUGAUUAAAUGGCCACAUUCAUAACAUAAUCAGUAUGGGCCCUAAGUUUUUAGGAAAACAUGGUAAGUGGGAUUAGAAUAUCUAAAGACGACAAGAAUAUUGUGUGGAUAUGGAGAAAGAAUGCAUUCUAUACCAGAGAAAGGCUGCUAUCAAAAACUCAGAGGCAAAAAAUAAUUUUGGGCAUAAUUAUGAGAUAGUAAAAAGAUCAGUAGUUGCCAGAAGUUGAGGAUGAAGGGGAAGGGACAAAUAGCAGAGCACAGGGGAUUUUUAGGGCAGUGAAAAUAACUCCCUAUGAUACUGUAAUGAUGGAUAUGUCACUAUAUGUUUGUCCAGACACAUAGACUGUACAGCACUAAGAAUCCUAGUGUAAACCAUGGACUUCAGAUGACUGUGUUAUGUGUCAGUGUAGGUUCAUCCAUUGUAAAUGUACCACUGUGGUGGGGGAUGUUGUUAAUGGGGAGGCUAUGCAUGUGUGGGGGCAAGUGAUACAUGGGAACUCUCUGUACCUUUCUCUCAAUUUUGCCAUGAACCUAAAACUGUUCUAAAAAAUAUGAAGUCUGUAAUUUUUAAAAAAUGUGAGUAUCAAGAGAAGAAUAUAAUAGAAUUCUAUAAAUAUCUUCCAGGUGAUGAAUAUGCUCAAAGUCAUAUGCUCUUGAAUUGAUAUCAGUAUUUGGCAGUCCCUAUCUGUGUGAAGACAUUUGCAAAGAUGAAAUAUUUAAAAUCUAAUUACAGAUCCGCGUUAACAGAUGAACGUUUGUAAUGGAUUUUGAUGGUCAACUCCACUGGGAAGCUUGGAAGUCAAAUGACCCAUGUUCUAAUCCCAGUUUUACUACUGGUUCACUUUGAGCCCUGUCCAAGCCAGUCUACUCUUAGCCUUUAGUUUUUUCAACUAAAAGGUAUGCAGAAGUUGGCUAGUCAAUACCUGAAGAGAGAUUGGCCUGGAGUAAAAGCUGAUGAUCGGAAUGAUUACAGGAGCAUGUAUCCCGUUUGGAAAUCUUUUCUCGAGGGAACAAUGCAGGUAGCCCAGUCUCGGAUGAAUAUAUGUGAAAACUAUAAAAACUUCAUUUCUGAGCCUGCAAGGACAGUGAGAAGCUUAAAAGAACAGCAACUAAAAAGGUGUGUGGACCAGUUGACAAAGAUCCAAACUGAAUUACAAGAGACAGUGAAAGAUUUAGCUAAAGGCAAAAAGAAAUACUUUGAGACUGAACAGAUGGCUCAUGCAGUACGAGAGAAAGCUGACAUCGAGGCAAAAUCUAAACUUAGUCUUUUUCAAUCAAGAAUCAGUUUACAGAAGGCAAGUGUAAAGUUAAAAGCCCGGCGAUCUGAGUGUAAUUCCAAAGCUACCCACGCAAGGAAUGAUUAUCUUCUUACCCUAGCGGCAGCAAAUGCACAUCAGGAUCGCUACUAUCAAACAGAUUUAGUUAACAUUAUGAAGGCUCUUGAUGGAAAUGUGUAUGAUCAUCUCAAGGAUUAUUUAAUAGCCUUCAGCCGGACUGAGCUAGAAACAUGCCAAGCUGUGCAGAACACAUUCCAGUUUUUAUUAGAAAACUCCAGCAAGGUGGUCCGGGACUACAAUCUUCAGCUGUUUUUGCAAGAAAACGCUGUAUUUCACAAACCCCAGCCCUUCCAGUUCCAGCCUUGUGACAGUGAUACUAGCCGACAGUUAGAAUCAGAAACUGGGACCACAGAGGAGCACAGUCUAAAUAAGGAAGCUCGAAAAUGGGCCACACGUGUGGCACGUGAGCAUAAAAACAUUGUUCACCAACAACGGGUUCUAAAUGAUCUGGAGUGUCAUGGAGCUGCUGUAUCAGAACAAAGCCGAGCAGAGCUAGAACAGAAAAUAGAUGAAGCUAGAGAAAAUAUUCGUAAAGCAGAGAUAAUUAAAUUGAAAGCUGAAGCCCGGUUGGACCUGCUAAAGCAGAUUGGUGUUUCUGUGGACACAUGGCUAAAGAGUGCCAUGAACCAAGUAAUGGAAGAACUGGAAAAUGAGCGAUGGGCCCGCCCUCCUGCAGUGACCAGUAAUGGCACUUUACACUCGCUUAAUGCAGAUACCGAAAGAGAAGAAGGCGAAGAGUUUGAAGAUAACAUGGAUGUUUUCGAUGACAGCAGUUCCAGCCCUUCUGGCACCUUAAGAAAUUAUCCACUCACCUGCAAAGUUGUUUAUUCCUACAAGGCUUCUCAACCAGAUGAGUUGACCAUUGAGGAACAUGAGGUGUUAGAAGUGAUUGAAGAUGGAGAUAUGGAAGACUGGGUAAAGGCUCGAAAUAAAGUUGGCCAAGUGGGUUAUGUGCCAGAAAAGUACCUACAGUUUCCCACCUCGAACAGCCUCCUGAGCAUGCUGCAGUCCCUGGCCGCUUUGGACAGUCGGUCACACACGUCCAGCAAUUCCACGGAAGCAGAACUCGUUUCAGGCAGCCUCAACGGAGAUGCCAGUGUAUGUUUUGUGAAAGCACUUUAUGAUUAUGAGGGCCAGACAGAUGAUGAGUUAUCUUUUCCUGAGGGAGCAAUAAUCCGUAUCUUGAACAAAGAAAACCAAGAUGAUGAUGGCUUCUGGGAAGGGGAAUUCAAUGGGCGUAUUGGAGUUUUCCCAUCGGUGCUAGUGGAAGAACUUUCAGCCUCAGAAAAUGGUGACACUCCAUGGAUGAGAGAGAUUCAGAUCUCUCCUUCCCCCAAGCCACACGCCUCCCUGCCUCCACUGCCGUUGUACGACCAGCCUCCCAGCAGCCCCUACCCCAGCCCAGAUAAGAGGAGCUCCCUGUACUUUCCCCGGUCUCCUUCAGCAAACGAAAAAAGCCUUCAUGCUGAGUCACCAGGAUUCUCACAGGCAUCAAGGCAUACUCCUGAGACCUCAUAUGGCAAACUGCGACCUGUCCGGGCAGCUCCCCCUCCACCUACACAGAAUCACCGAAGGCCAGCAGAGAAGAUUGAAGAUGUGGAAAUCACACUGGUGUGAUGAUGGGCUUGCCCAUCCAUUACUGCUACAAUCAAGGCCAGGCUUGGAGUUUGGCCAGUCUUGUUUUUUAGGCACCUUUGCAUGAUGAUGACUCUUGAACAGAGCAAAAAACAAGGAGGAUUAUGUGUGACUGGGUGGCCUGGUAGACUCCUCCCACGUUUUGAAUAUUUCGUGCCUUUUUUUUUUGUUGUCAUUUUCUAUGUCAUUUCUCCUACCAUAGCACAAAUCCUAGCGGACCCUAGGAGCAAAGAGGGGGGCAGCCCUCAUGCCUAACAGUGGUCUGUUUUUAUAUGAGACUCAAGAACAGGCCUCAUUCCAGGGCACAGUCCCUAAAUUACUGAUCAUGUGCACUCGUACAGUAUAUUACUGUGACCACAAGGAUGUGGCAAAGAUUCUCAUCUUUCUUCAAGUGGCUUUUGCUCAUCUGAUUGAGAAUUAAUCAGAUCAUGUUGGCUACAUAAGGAAACAGAAGGAGGGAUUUCAGGAGAGGCUGGCUCCUCCCCAAGGUUAGUCCCCAGACUGAGAAAGUGAAACCUUAUUGGGAAAAAUUGGACUGCCCUGAAUUUAGCACCAAUUGCAUUAACGCACAUCUCUUCCACAACUAACAGACUUAAAAUAACAGUGUCCUUCGUAUUAAUAUCUGUGCCAUUCAUUUAGAAUUAGCAGAGCUAAUAUGGAGGGGCUGAACUAGUAGCCACAUCUUGUUCAUCACAUAGACUAAUAGAAAGGAGGCUGUGGCUAAAGCAGAAAUGGAACUUCCGGAUCUGAAAUUAGCCAAUAUAAUGUUCUUUUGUAUUUGGGUAUUUUUCAUCUUAAUUUUUACAGCAUAUACUCUUCUUACCAGUAUCCUUAGAAUCCAAAUGUCUAGAUAAGUUGAGGACACAUACCUGCAUUGUUGAGCUUCUCUACUGGGGACGCCCCGGCAUUAUUUUAUUCCCAAGCCAGCAGACCGGCCCAGACAGCCAGGCUGUGGCUGGUCCAGACCAACUGCUAUGGUGGAAAAUGCAGCUUCCAGGUCCCACUACCCUGACAUUUCCGUGGAAGGAAGAACCUGGUGGCUCGUGGAGGAAACCAGCUUUCUAUGAGAAAGGACUGAAGGAUUGCGCACCCUGCACAAGUACAGAUUGACCAGGAAAAGACAAGUGUCUUCUGUGUGUCACAGGGAAAGCCAGGAGUGGCCUUCUCUGCAGGCCAGCAAGCCUGCAGCAGCAGGUGCCCCCACGUCAGGUGCUGACUGUCUGCUGUCCGCUCCUGUAGAAGGUAGGGAGCACAAUACCUAGGGACUAAGGGAUGUUCGCCGGUUGUGGUUUGUUUUUUUUUUUUUUCCUUGGUUAAGAAAUCAAAUUUGCAGAAUUUAAUCUACAAGUUGUAUUAUGCUUUGAAAACUCCAUCCCUCCUAAGAAUCUUAAAAAACUUGAAAUGCUCGCCAAAUGUCCCCAUGGGAUUUUUGACCAAAAGUAAGGUGAUAACUGAAGAAAUUUUUAGUUCUUUGAUCACUUCAGUGACAAUACCCAUUAAUGAAUCUUCUCCAUGAUUUGGGGUUUUUUUUCGUUGUUGUUUUUUACACUUCUUAACCUGUUGAUCUAUUUGAGGUCUUUUGUGUUUAUCAAACUUAUUCUUAAGUUUAAAAAAGAAAUUAAAAGGGUGGUUUUUUUAAGAUUUUAAAGUUUGCUAACAUAUUAAAAAUCUUCAAAUGCUUAUUAAAUAGAGCAGUUCUUGCCACCCAGUCUUGUAUUCUGUCUUUAGCUAGCCAAAUUGUCCUUGAAUUUGGGUUUUCCACAACCUCAAAGGGUUAUUUGAAAUCUUUUGUUGUAUUUUAAAAUAUUUUUUGGAAGAGCUGCUAAUUUUAUUUUAAAAAACAAAGUUGUGAAAACAUGCCUCCUUUUUAAAAAAUAACCCCUCCAUCCAGGAUAUGGAAUCCAGCACCACAGUGCACAGGUCAGGGCUCGGAGGGAGCCUCUGUGCAGAUGUGCUUUCUUUACAGUGGCUGUAAAAAGUUUGUAUUUAUUAUGUAUAAAAUGUUGAAUAAUAAAAAAAAUGGAAUUA